GACUUCCCCCGGGCUGAGCUGCGCAGCGGGUGCGGAGGGCGGGCGCCCGGCGUCCGGCGGCGGGUGGGGGGCUGUGAGGCUGGCAGGGGUCGGCGGGCGCGUAGCCGCCGACCCUUGGUGGUCUCUUGGGCUGGGGACCCUUCCCUGGGAGUCGGCCCCGGCCCCGGCGGGGCGGGCGUUGCCGGGAGGCGGAGGGGUGCGCGGCCGCGAGUCCUGCGUGAUCGCGAGCAUGUGUGCGUGCGCGUGUUUAUCUGAGGCGCGUGCGGCGGCCACCCCAGCCUAGUCCUCUUCUUGGUGCCACUGGCUAACUAGGUUGAGAAACCGGCGCCACAGGCGGCACACCUGGCCCGGAGCUGGCCCGCUCCUCCCCGCCGAGCCGGCGCCCCAACAACGCGCCCUCUCCCAGUCCUCACAAAGGGGCCUAGUCCGGCCCCCGGCUCUGGCCGUGAGGGAGCGCUGUGGGGGCGCGCUGCCUUCUGCCUGGAAGUGUUGGGCAGGUGGUGGGAGAGCGUCAGGCUUGAACAACAUGAUUUUAAAGCACGUGUCUGUCUGUCGUUUUUUACUUUUAGGGUUUUGGCCAAAUUGGGCGAGGGCACAAAAUAACCACUUACCCCUUCUCACCGAGGAAGAGCGGGAGAAAGGGUAUGGCACAGUCACAAGGGUGGGUGAAAAGAUACAUCAAGGCCUUUUGUAAAGGCUUCUUUGUGGCGGUGCCUGUGGCAGUGACUUUCUUGGAUCGGGUCGCCUGUGUGGCAAGAGUAGAAGGAGCAUCGAUGCAGCCUUCUUUGAAUCCUGGGGGGAGCCAGUCAUCUGAUGUGGUGCUUUUGAACCACUGGAAAGUGAGGAAUUUUGAAGUACACCGUGGUGACAUUGUAUCAUUGGUGUUGCUCACUGUGACGCCCUCCACCCGACAACAGGAGAUUGGUGGAGAAGAAGAGGAAGUGGAGAAAGAUAUUUCAUUGGCAAAGUCUCCUAAAAACCCAGAACAGAAGAUCAUUAAGAGAGUGAUUGCUCUUGAAGGAGAUAUUGUCAGAACCAUAGGACACAAAAACCGGUAUGUCAAAGUCCCCCGUGGUCACAUCUGGGUUGAAGGUGAUCAUCAUGGACACAGUUUUGACAGUAAUUCUUUUGGGCCGUGUCAUAUAUGCAAAGAUCAUAGCUCUCAUUUCUACCAAGUGAAUUCACAGAGAAAGAAAAAGAGAUUCAGGAAGAGAAAAAAAAAAAUGCUACUGAGUUUAACACAACACUACCUUCUGGGAACAAAGGCAAGUAUUUUAGUUUGGAGAAAUGAUUUGAAAUUUACAACCAAACACUUUAAUUGUCCUGGCUUUGCUACUCCUGGUUGUUUUCUCUGGUUUAUAGUUGUCCUUGGUCCUAGGGCUCUCAGGAUGUUUGGGGAAAGCAGGUUGAUGAGCCAGAGACCUUCUUGGCAGCUUUCCAAGAGUCUUUGAUCAUCUGAGAGAUCUGAGGACAAAAAUUUCAGAGUCUAUAAAAAGCACUGCCAUACCGCAUAUUAGGUAAGUGGAUCAGACCUUUGGCCUCAGAUAAUAAACACCUUUAUUCUUUAACAUAUAAUGAUAGUUAGAGUCAUACUACCCUCUCUCCCAGCAUGUUCUCUCAUAUUGUUCCCAGAAAUAAGCCCCUGGGCAAAAUCUCUUUUGAUCCUUUUGCAGCAAAGUUUUUAUUUUGUUCUUACUAUUGUUAGGUGAAGCAAACAUUUUUUCCUGCUCUGAGCACUAAAGGUGAUUUAGCUACCUGUUUUACAUACUUAUUCCUGCCUAAGGUGCUCUGGUGGUGAGAUUCUAAGGCUAGGUGGCACAGGUGAUGAAUCUUUCUCUGGGGGAAAAAAAUUUUCAGGUGAAUGCUUCCAUCUGGCACCUGUCCUGGCUGAUGGCACUCAGUGUUUACCUGGCAUCCAUUCUUCUGAGGGUGAUUGGUUACAUGGCAGGCCUGUGGCCCCUGGCAGGUGGGAAAAAGCACCUAUUUCAUGAGAACCAAGUUGUGCUUUACUCCACAAAGGCCAGGGUGUUUGAGAAGAUCACUACUGCCAACUGUAAUCUCUUCUUCCAAUUCUUUCAGUUAAAUUUGUCUUAAUCCCUACAAUUCUCUUUGUAGAAAAGUCAGCUCCCAAUCUUAGUCUACUUUCAUACUUUGCACUGUCACAUGCUAUAGUUUUCUCUUCUUCAAACUGUUUGCAACUCAAGAGUUAAGUUUUUGAUUGUACAGCAAAUACUAAACUACAAAAGCUGUGAACUCAAAAAUUUAAUUCUUUGUUCUAAGAUGGUAUAAUGGUGAGGUAUAUAUGUUUAUACUUAUAUACUUGGAAGGACGGAGCACAAAGCUUUCUUCCUUCCAGGGGUUGUCUCCUAUUUCUUCUGGUACCAGUCUCCUUGAUGAAUUGCUAGAACACUGUUUAGCAACUUUCUUCAGUAUUGAGUUGAGCUAAUGUGUAUAUGUUACAUAUACACUAUAUAUAUAUAUAAAGUUGCAUAUAACACACACACACACACACUCUUAACUUUGUGUUAAUAUGACCAGUAAGGCCUGAUUUAUGUCUAGUGACCAUUUCUUACAUGACAGGCUGCUGUGCUGGUAUGGGAAAGUGAUAGUCUAAACUGAAUGUGCUCCAGCAGUAACUACAGUGAAUUUCUGUGGAAGUCCCAGUUUUAAAACUACAUUUAAGAUUUAUUAUUCAUAAAGAAUAUUUGAAGAAGCUUUAAAAAUAAAUUACAAUAAAAAACUAGAGACUUCUAAAUAAACUUAGAACAACCAAUGAAAUUAUAAGGAGAAAGACGCUAGAAGCAACUUCAAAUGAAUUUAUUAAUAUAGAUGAGCACUAAACUUAAUUCUCAAGUUACUGGCAUCUGAAGCAAAAAAGAAAAUAACUUAGUUGAUCUAGUUCUCAUUGUUUACCUGAAGAGAACUUUCAUAUUCAUCUCAGAGGCCUUCAUGAAUCAGGCUGGUAAGUAAAUGAGAGAAUUGACUGGGCAUAAACCAAAGAGAAUGGUACAGCUUGUGUUUGCCCCAUUCAAAGGAGUUUGAGCUAAAGCUAAGCAGAAACCAAAAUCUUUUUCACUGACUAAAUAAAACCAAAGGGCUGAGAUGCACUUAGACAGCUGAGUUACCAUUGAAAUACAGGGGAAAUUUAUCCUGAAUUUGUCAUAUUAGGCCUUCUGUAACAUGAAAUGUAAUGUUUAAUAUGCAAGUUAUUUUAUUUAAAAAAGUCAUUGCUUUAAAUCGUCUUCUAAUAUUGAACUUCUGAAAAAGCUGAAAGAUUAAAUUUAUUGUUUUGCCUCAGUGAAUGUACUAUGAAGUCUCUAAAAAUCAGCCAUCCCCCCAGAUGGUCUAAGAAUGCCCCUAGGUGGCAAGACAUAAUUAAAAAUACUCUAAUUUUGUGAUUAAAGCUCUCUCUCUCUUUUUUUUUUUUUUUUUGAGACGAAGUUUCACUCUUGUCACCCAGGCUGGAGUGAAAUGGCACAAUCUUGGCUCACUGCGACCUCUGCCUCCCAGGUUCAAGCGAUUCUCCUGCCUCAGCUUCUUGAGUAGCUGGGAUUACAGGCACCCACCACCACACCCUGCUACUUUUUGUAUUUUUAGUGGAGAUAGGAUUUCACCAUGUUGGCCAGGCUAGUGUCAAACUCCUGACCUCAGAUAAUCUGCCUGCCUCAGCCUCCCAAAGUGCUGGGAUUACAGGCAUGAGCCACCGUGCCCGACCUCAUGAUUAAAACUCUUCUAAGAGCUCCACUUUUUCUUGUUCUAGAAUGAAUAUCUCCAGCAAUGCAAUAAAUGUUCUCCCUUGCAUUAAAUAGGAAGCAAGGCCAUAAUAUGACAAUUAAUUACAUCUUAUGUAUGAGGUAGAAUGUGGCAGAGGGGAGUGAGGCAUUACUGAUCACCAGUAGAGUUCCCAGAGGAAAACAUGUCAGGAGCUGUACUGGAGGGAGCAGGGAAACCUGCCCUAAUCCUUUCUCCUACUGGCCUGGUUACCUAAAUGCAUUCUCAGAAUUAGAAAAACUCAUCACGACUUCUGUGUCUAUUUCUAUAUGUUUAUGUUAUUCAUAUGAUCAGAGAAACCUGAAUUCUCCCUCUGCAUUCUCAUACUCCAGUAAUUUUUAUCUCUGUGAUAGCAGAAUUCCUAUGAAGAAUUCUAAGUUUCUUGGUGGUACUUGUGAACAAAAGAAACUUUUUAUUAUUAUCACUAUGUGCAAAAUGCCUGUCCAGGGUUAAGUGGUGAUCCAUGUGACUUAAAUUCAGUUCUGGGUAGGUACAUAGCUCGAGACUUGGGCUUCACAACGUUCUGAGUUCACCAAUGGUCACCAGGCCAAGUAAAGCUACAGAAAAGCUAGGAAGCACGCCACCAGCAGGCCCCUUUUAGAUUGUGAAAAAUAGGGAAGGCAGGCUUGUCAGCUGAAGAGAGUGGUCUAUGACUACUGGCUAGAAGAGAAGGAAUGUGUCACAUACUGGGACGUCCUGAACUUUAGCAUGGCUUACUUUGCUAAGAUGUUAUUUAGCAAAACCCAUGAAUAUACCAGGAUAACGACAGUACAGUGCAAAACCUGGCUAAAAUCAGAAUGACAGAGUAGGGUUUUUUUGUUUGUUUUUUCUUUGUUUGUUUUGAGAGGAGUCUUGCUCUGUCCCCAGGCUGGAGUGCAGUGGUGCAAUCUCGGCUCACUGCAACCUCCACCUCCCAGUUCAAAUGAUUCCCCUGCCUCAGCCUCCUGAGUAGCUGGGACUACAGGCACACGCCACCACACCCAGCUAAUUUUUUGUAUUUUAGUAGAGACGAGGUUUCACCACGUUGGCCAGGGUAGUCUUGAUCUCCUGACCUCGUGAUCCGCACACCUCAACCUCCCAAAGUGUGGGGAUUACAGGCGUGAGCCACCGCGCCCAGCCCUACAGAGUGGUUUUAAAGUCAAAUCAGUUCGGAAGCAGUUUUAAAAAAAACCCUGCUGGGACCUUUAGCUUCAAUUAGGGACUUUCACCGAAGCCUCUAACAAGUCUGAGAGCACUGUUUGUUUUAAAGCACUAAACACUUUAGACUUCACCUGGAAAGAAUACCUGGGUACCUCUGAAUAAAUCAGUGACCCCAAAUGUCUAGAGAACAAAUGAAGAUUCUGCAGAUUCUUUCCCUCUAGUAUUUUCGUCAGGCCAGAGCAUUCUUCUUUUAGUGCAUGGUUAUUUUUAUACUUGCUAUUGCAACCCUUUAUUGAAAUAUUUGUAACCUCUCAUAACAGCCUCUUUUGAUAAGUUUCCAUUUCGGUUUUCAUUUUGCAAAUGAGAUCUUAUUUACCAAGUUGGCUGCUUGUGUCUUUUGGCUAAAUAUGCAGCAUAUUUUAGGGGCUAUAACAAGAUACGUUUGAAAGGCCAAUAAUUUGUUAUUACCAUAUGGUAGAAAGAAUAAAGAAGUUUUCUCAAGAUUCCCAUUCCCAAAUUGUGUAAUCAAACACUCACCCAGAUACUUAUGUGAAGGGACUUUGGAGACAGAAUUAAGUUUAAUAAUUCUGACCUUAAAUUAGAUAAGGAACCUGAAUGUUUCUAGGGGAGGGGGCAAUAUUUAAUGUAAUCACACAAACCCUUAAAAGCAAAGCAGGAAAACAGAAAAGUUAGAGAGAAGCUGUUGAAGAUGGAGGCAGAAGAAAGAUGAGGUAGAAGGGAAGGUAGAGAGAUUUGAAACAUGAGGAUUCAACCCACUGUUGCCAACUUUAAGGGUCGAGGAAUGCAAGUGGCCUCUAGAAACUGAGAACGACCCCAGUCCACAGGCAGCAAGGAAGCCAGACCUCACUCCUUCAGCUACGUGGAGCUAAAUUUGUCCAGCAAUCCAAAUGAGCUUGGAAGUGAACUCUCCCCCAGGGCCAGGCCAGCAGACACUUUAAUUUCGGCCUUGGGAAACCCAGAGCAGCCAGUUCUGACUUCUGACCUACUGAACUGUGAGGUAAUAGACUUGAGUUGUUCUAAGCCUGUGUUUGCUCUAAGCUGCUAUACGUCUGUGGUGAUUGUACAUAUACUGUAAUGGUAGCAAUAGAAAACUGGUAAGGCUCAAAAUGCCUUGGAGUAUCUGAGUGUCCAGGUUUACUUGAUUUCAACAACAGCUGGUGGGGAAAAGAGAGCAAGGGAGGAAGAGAGAGAAAAUAAAAAGAAAAAGAGGAGAGGAGGUAUCUGACAUUAUAAACAGUAGGGACAAUUUGGUCUCCAUUCCAUACUAUGACUCUCAAGUGGCUUCUUGCACACCUCAUGGUAUUAGCCUCUCACAUCACUGAGUGCAUUUUUAAAAUUGAAAUAUUUUGAUGUUUUUUUUGUUUGCAGUACAAGAUGGCCUUCUUUAUUAUAAACUGUGUCCUACUGAGAACAUUAUAUUUAUGAAUAGUUACAGUACAGGGUUGUGUAUGUAAAACUGUGUCCACUUUACUUUAAGGAAACUGUAAGAGAUCUUCAAGGGUAUUUUGAUUUCAGGUCAUUUUUGUCUUAUAGACUGUUUUUUUUUAGAAACAAACCCCCAUGUGAAGUCCAACACGUUUGUCCUAAAUGCUGUCCCUCCUAGCCACAGCCUUUGGAGAACCUGAGCUUCUAGAAGGAAGCGGUCCACAGGAAAGUGAAGGAGCCUCACUAUUGCUAAAAAGGCAUAAGGCCCAUGUAUAUGCUGUCAGCCCAUCAAUUCCCUCAACUUCUCUACACAAGAUUAGAAUGUCCCUUUUUCCUUUCUAAGCACACUACAAAUCAUUCCUUUUUUAACCUCUUUUCUCAUGCACGGUAACCUGGGAUGUUAGUGAUAAAUAAUCUGAUUUAACCUAAGAAAAUUUGGAGAGUUGGGGAAGGGAAUGACACUAAGCACAUAUGUGACUUGCCCCAGCCCUGUUCCCUCAUUGGUAUCCUCAAUGCCCAGGAAAAAAAGCGCUGAUUGAGAUUAAUUUAUCAAUGCAUAAUAUCCUUUCUCUUUGGAUACCUAGCUUCAAUAUUGCUUCUCUCUCAAAUCUCUUUGUAAUUUUCUAUGCAGGAAACUUGGGAGGCCUCCCACAGAUUGGCUCAUUUUAACAAAAACACAUUUCUUCUGCCCUCUACAACCUCCAGGAGCCUUCAAAGAUGAAGUUAAUUAUACAUAUUUUAAAAAGAGACCAAAUGCAGAGUCUUGAGGAUUUCAAGUUCUAAAACUAGAUUUAUUAUGUUCAAAGUUGUGUCUGGAUAAAAGGAAAGUAUAACAUUAAAAUAUGAAUCUAUUCAUGCCAUUUAGUACUUUGAAUUAUUCACAGAUGCUUGGGGUUUUUCUCUCUUUUUUUGUUUUUUUGUUUUUCUAAGAAUAAGGCAUUUAUCUGAAACCAAUGAAAUGGAAAGGAAUAUUUUUUCGUUUUUAGAAUUCUUCCCAUUUGGGGUUGUUUUAUUAUAGAACACCACCCCUCAGACAUUUUAUGAGCUAUAUUCAUAACACAUUUACAUGUGAUUGAAGCACUUAACAGAAAAAUUAGGUAAAUUGAGCACUAACAGCUAAAGCAAAAUGCUAGGCAACUAUUUCCAAAUGUAAAGUGCUUUGAAGCUGUUAAGCUGUUAUAUCCCACUCCCCCAAGCUCUCCUUCCUCUGAGAAUUAUAAAGGAGAUGAUGUUCUAUAAAAUAUUUGGUGAUGUCUGUUUUAGUCUUCCAUCUACAUUUUCUAACCUGAUUGGGGAGUUUAGCUUUAGCACCUCCCCAUUUUAUGUUGUUUAUUCAGUAAUCUUCUAGGUACAGAAUAAACUUUUUGAAUUUCUGCUCUCCUAUUUGUAAAAAGACAAUAAUAAUACCAUCUUUGCCAAUCUCAUAGGAUCAGGAAGCUUGAACAAUGUGAUAUACAAGGAUAUAAACUUUAAAUAGCCAUACAUAUAUGAAGUAUUGGAAAUGAUGUUACUUCUAACAUUGUUAUUAGCAAUAACUUUACAGACUCAAGAUGCUACGAAGACUUAGAAGGCACAGAACUUAUACUCAUUAUAGUUGAGGAUUCAGAAAUAUCAUUUAGGCCUGGAAUAUUUUAUUUAUGUUCUAAUAUUUGUUUGGUUACAAGCAUUUUGAAAGAUAGUAUUAUGCUCACUAAAUUUUUGCUCUCCACUCUUGCCCAGGUUUUUCAACCAUAUCUCAUUUACCAAAAUCUUCAGAAUCUUUUAGAUCCCUGGUUGUUUUCCUGUGGAGAGUCUUGUUAGUGUUUUACUCAUAAUUGAACUUUACAUGUGAUAUAUCUUGUGUAGAGUAGACUAGGCUUGCCCCAUCUUCAUUUGACAUAUACAUUUCUUUUAGUAUCACCUAAGGUCACAUUUAUUUUUUGCCAGUCUCUCAUAUAGUGUAUUCCAUGCUGGAAUGAAUUAGGAGUAUCAGGGGAGGAGACAUACUCUGCAGUGAUUCUUUGGAAUUUAAGGAGGGCCAUUAUUGAUCAUAUAAUCCAAAGAUCCUUGAUUUGACAUAAGAAACAGAGUGCCAGAAUGAUCAAGCAGUUUGCUUAAGAUCACACAGUUGGUUGUUAGCAAGGGUAGAAUUAAAAUUCUGAUGAUUCCAGACCUAACGCUCUUACUACUGUGCAGGGGAAGGAGGGAGAACACAAGAAGAAAGAUGGCUUAGUGCAGGAGUCAGCAAACUAUGGCCCGUGGGCCGUAUCUGGGCCUAUUUUUGUAAAUAAAGUUUUUUUUGGAACACAGCAUGCCCAUUCAUUAACAUAUUAUAUAUGGCUGUUUUCACACUACAAGGGCAGAGCAGAAUAGUUUUCUGAGACCAUCUGGCCUACAAAGCCUAAAAUGUUUAGUCUGGUCAUUUACAUAAAAAAUUUGCUGACCUCUGGCUUAGAGGAGAGAUGACUAAAAAAUCUGGAUAGGAGCACUUUGAGAACAGUCUUUUUAGUUUGCACACUUGUUUCUAGUUCUUAUUUAGAAGAAACUGCAUGGCUGUUAGGUGAACUUGUCUAACUCUCUCAUGAUUAACUGCUGAUUUAUUUAAUAAAUUUGCAUAUAUCCUUGCAGAAGGAUCAGUACAUAUUUUCCAGAGGUGUUUCUUAUGUGAUUUGUUUUCUAUGUUCAUCUUCAUAAUAUAUUCUUGAUGAUAUUAGUAUGUCUUUAUUCAAAGUACUGGAAACUUACAUGGGAUACACAAUAGCUGUAUUCAAGUAUGUGAAGGACUCUUUUCCUGUGAAUAAAGGGAUUAGAUGUAUUUAUCCUUCAAGUCCAAUUAAAAUGUGCUUUUGUUGUCAAGCCCCUGAUUCCAGCUACUCCCUUCUUUGGGCAGAAUUAAUCACCCUCUCUUCUGUGCUUCCAAAAUUCUUUGUACAAAGUACUGUUACAGUAUUUGUCACACAACGCUAUAGGUCUUGUUUGCACAUUUGUCUCCCCAGUUGAUUGUGAAAUCCUUGAAAGUGAGGACAAUAUCUUAUUCAUUUUGGCAUCCUCAUCAUGGGGCUCAGGCCCUGGCUCAUAGAAGCAACCUAAUGCUUGAUGAGUGAAGGUAUAUUAUAAUCCCAGAGGGCAAAGCAAGGACCAUUGUGAAAUCUCACUAAAAAGAACUCUGUGGUAGUGCUGGCAACCAAUUGAAAAGUCUCCUAAGCAGUGUGCUUGGACAUCAAGGACAAGAACUUGGGGUUAGAAUGCCUAGGUUUGCAUUUUGACUGUCCUGUUUAAUAACGGUCUUUGGGUGGGUUGCUUAUCUCUGAACCUCAAUUUCCUCAGCUUUGAAAUGGAGAGGAUAUAGGGAAGCAGUUUUCUAAGUGGAGUCUAUAAACCCCUGGGUAUUUCCAAAACAAUCUCAAGGGGUAUUUGAGGUCAAAACUAUUUUUAUUAGAAUGCUAAGAAAUUUGUCAUUUUUACUCUGUCAAUACUGGCAUUGAUGGUACAAAAGCAAUGGUGGGACAACUCCUGGUGUCUUUGUACAAAUCAAAGCAGUAGCACCAAGUUGAACUAAUAGUCAUUGUUUUCAUCCCCAUCAUAUACUGUCAUGAGAAAAAAUACAUACCAGUUUCACUUAAGAAUGCCUUUGAUGAAGGAGUAAAAUUAUUAACUUUUUUUUUUUAGUCUCUGGAAUGUAUUUUUAUUUAUUUUUUUAAUAUACUUUAAGUUCUAGGGUACAUGUGCACAAUGUGCAGGUUUGUUACAUAUGUAUACAUGUGCCAUGUUGGUGUGCUGCACACAUUAAGUCGUCAUUUACAUUAGGUAUAUCUCCUAAUGCUAUCCCUCCCCACUCCCCCAACCCCAUGACAGGCCCCAGUGUGUGAUGUUCCCCUUCCUGUGUUGAAGUGUUCUCAUUGUUCAGUUCCCACCUAUGAGUGAGAACCUGCGGUGUUUGGUUUUCUGUCCUUGCGAUAGUUUGCUGAGAAUGAUGGUUUCCAGCUUCAUCCAUCUCCCUACAAAGGACAUGAACUCAUCCUUUUUUAUGGCUGCAUAGUAUUCCAUGGUGUAUAUGUGCCACAUUUUCUUAAUCCAGUCUAUCAUUGAUGGACAUUUGGGUUGGUUCCAAGUCUUUGCUAUUGUGAAUAGUGCCACAACAAACAUAUGUGUGCAUGUGUCUUUAUAGCAGCAUGAUUUAUACACCUUUGGGUAUAUACCCGGUAAUGGGAUAGCUGGGUCAAAUGGUAUUUCUAGUUCUAGAUCCCCGAGGAAUCGCCACACUGACUUCCACAAUGGUUGAACUAGUUUACAGUCCCACCAACAGUGUAAAAGUGUUCCUGUUUCUCCACAUCCUCUCCAGCAGCUGUUGUUUCCUGACUUUUUAAUGAUCACCAUUCUAACUGGUGUGAGAUGGUAUCUCAUUGUGGCUUUGAUUUGCAUUUCUCUGAUGGCCAGUGAUGAUGAGCAUUUUUUCAUGUGUCUGUUGGCGCAUAAAUGUCUUCUUUUGAGAAGUGUGUGUUCAUAUCCUUCGCCCACUUUUUGAUGGGGUUGUUUGUUUUUUUCUUGUAAAUUUGUUUGAGUACUUUCUAGAUUCUGGAUAUAAGCCCUUUGUCAGAUGACCAGAUUGCGAAAAUUUUCUCCCAUUCUGUAGGUUGCCUGUUCACUCUGAUGGUGGUUUCUUUUGCUGUGCAGAAGCUCUUUAGUUUAAUUAGAUCCCAUUCGUCAAUUUUGGCUUUUGUUGCCAUUGCUUUUGGUGUUUUAGACAUGAAGUCGUUGCCCAUGCCUAUGUCCUGAAUGGUAUUGCCUAGAUUUUCUUCUAGGGUUUUUAUGGUUUUAGGUCUAACAUUUAAGUCUUUAAUCCAUCUUGAAUUAAUUUUUGUAUAAGGUGUAAGGAAGGGAUCCAGUUUCAGCUUUCUACAUAUGACUAGCCAGUUUUCCUAGCACCAUUUAUUAAAUAGGGAAUCCUUUCCCCAUUUCUUGUUUUUGUCAGGUUUGUCAAAGAUCAGAUGGUUGUAGAUGUGUGGUAUUAUUUCUGAGGGCUCUGUUCUAUUCCACUGAUCUAUAUCUCUGUUUUGGUACCAGUACCAUGCUGUUUUGGUUACUGUAGCCUCGUAGUAUAGUUUGAAGUCAGGUAGCAUGAUGCCUCCAGCUCUGUUGUUUUGGCUUAGGAUUGACUUGGCAAUGCGGGCUCUUUUUUGGUUCCAUAUGAACUUUAAAGUAGUUUUUUCCAAUUCUGUGAAGAAAGUCAUUGGUAGCUUGAUGGGGAUGGCAUGGAAUCUAUAAAUUACCUUGGGCAGUAUGGCCAUUUUCACGAUAUUGAUUCUUCCUAUCCAUGAGCGUGGAAUGUUCUUCCAUUUGUUUGAGUCCUCUUUUAUUUCGCUAAGCAGUGGUUUUUAGUUCUCCUUGAGGAGGUCCUUCACAUCCCUUGUAAGUUGGAUUCCUAGGUAUUUUAUUCUCUUUGAAGCAAUUGUGAAUGAGAGUUCACUCAUGAUUCGGCUAUUUGUUUGUUACUGGUGUAUAAGAGUGCUUGUGAUUUUUGCACAUUGAUUUUGUAUCCUGAGACUUUGCUGAAGUUGCUUAUCAGCUUAAGGAGAUUUUGGGCUGAGAUGAUGGCGUUUUCUAGAUAUACAAUCAUGUCAUCUGCAAACAGGGACAAUUUGACUUCCUCUUUUAUUAAAUGUCAAUCUUUGAGUAUAAUAUCCUUUUUAAUAUUUGGUGUGAUAAAAUGGGAAGUAUAUAUAAAUCACUUUUACAUUUUGGAAGUACAAGGGCUGUCUUGAGAAAAGUACUGUGGUAUUGAAUUGCCAGCUGAACAAGCCACUUGAAACUAGACAUGAUGUUUCAAAAGCAUGCACAUAGGUAAAGAUCCAUUGAAAGUGCAAUACAGGCUGGGAGCGGUGGUUCAUCCCUGUAAUAUCAGCACUUUCAGAGGUCGGGGAUGGAGUAUCUCUUGAGUCCAGGAGUUUGAGCCCAGCCUGGGCAACAUAGGGAGAACCCAUCUUUACCAAAAUUAAAAAAUAAUAAGCCAGGCGUGGUGGUGUGUGCCUGUGGUCCAGCUAGUCAGGAGGCUGACAUGGGAGGAUCUCUUGAGCCUGGGGAAUUCAUAUAUAUUUUGCAAACAUUAAAAAUAGUUACUUAUCUAGAACUAUACAAAGAGUUCUAAUAUACGUUAAGUAUUAAAAUAGCUGCAGAAAAUUAUUUUUAGUCUAUCCUAUUUGUGUAAAUAAUUAGCAGUUUUCUGUGAAUAGAGACAAAUGCCUAGAAACUGGAGUUACAUGGGAGAAAAUGAUUAGGGGCUAAAGAAGGGUGAAAGGAGACAUUCAGAUCUCAUUUCAUACCCUUUCAUAUUUUGUUAUUUACGUAUCCAUUUUUUGUCUUGUUUAAAAAAUUAAUGUAGGUGAUAAUACCCAUAAUUAUAAUGUAAACUAGUUGAGCAGCGUUAAAUCUCCUGGCCUAUAGAGAAUGUUUAUAAUGUAAGUAUUGCAUUAUGUAUGUAAUUAUUACAUAUGCAGUGACACUGUUGGUUGUCCAAGUGAAUGACCACUUCAUGUGUUAGUGUGAUCCCAUCAGUAGAGUGUUCUCCAAGCAAUUACUGAAUGAUAAAGAAAUAUCAUAGAUCAGACUUCUGCCUCUGAGUAUAUUCAACUGAUCUCUCAGUUUAAAUUCCGAUGUUCUUUGAUACUGUUAUUAAUUAAUGAAUAGCCAUAAUGUUUUGAGAGUAGUUCUUUACCAAAGGUCCUCCAUCAAAAUCUUAUCUCUGAGCAACUUUAAAAUCUUCAGAAUUUUUUUCAUCUGUUAGUUUUGAUAGCAUUCACUUUUCACCUUUAAUUUUGCUCUCAAAGUAUGUUGGGGCUACUAGGACAAAUAAGUAAAUAUUCACUGAGUCUUUACUGCAUCACAGUAGGAAGAACUCUGAUCUUUUAUAAGGUUAGGAAAAGAACUUAGUACCUUAAUUUCACCAUUGCCAGUUCCACAAACUGAAAUUUAUUUAGCAGAAUGUCCCUAUUCUUAGGAUAAGCUUGUCUUUAGGAUAAACUUUUCCUGUCAGAUAAAUGAUGGAAUUUGCCAUCUUUAAAUAAAGAAUACUCCAUAUAUUAUUAUAUAAUUUUUAAAAAUUACUUAGUGAUUACCACAACUGCUUUUUGGGUUGAGUAAUAUAAUCUCUUUGAGUCAAGAGUCAAGUAAUGUAAUCACAUCAACAUAUACAGACAAACUUGUGUCUACUGUAUAUGCAACUAUAUUUUUAUAAUAUAGGAGUUAGGUUUUUGUGUGAAAAUAGGUGUACCUUUCUGGAAGAACAGAAAUAAUUUACUCCUGGCAUCUUAUUGAAAGAAAAAAGUCAAUUCAAUUUGAAUAAUGUUGGGAGAUAAAGCAUGCCAGUAUUAUUCUUUAUUUCUUUUAUUAAUGAGUUAGGAUACAAAAAAGUCAAUAAAAAUUACAUUAAAAACUCAUAAACAUUGUUCAAAUCUUAUUUCUCCAUCAGUCAUGUUCAUAAAACUGGCAUUUCCAUUUAAAUGGCAGUUAAUAACAAUAGGAUUUUAUUUAGUGAGCCAAACAACACACGGCCUCAUUUAUUUACUCAUCAGACACUUGAGUGCCUUCUCUAUGCCAGAUCCCGUGCCAGGUACUGGGGCCCCAGCCUUGAAUAAGACAUAGAAUAAGACAUACUUCUUACAUUCUGUGAAUUUAGUGGCCAAUGGAGCAGAAAGACAUGUAAGCAAAUAAUUAAAGAAGUAACAUUUUGAAAUAGGAAGGGCAUAAGAUUUGGGGAGUAAACAUAUUUUAAACUUGGGCUUCCUCACUUCUGAAUUAUAGACUUCUAACCUUUCUAAGUUUCAGGGAUAAUAAUUUCAGUGUGUGUCUUUUUUAAGGAUUAGAGAAAACAUUAAAAGUACAGAGCCUGGAACUAAAUCUAUUCAAAUGAGAUUUAUUUAUUACCCUUAAACUAUAAUAUGAAAGGUACUAUAUUCAGGAAUGUACAAGAAAGAAUGGAUAAUUGGCUUGGGGAUGGAGACAGGUAAGGAAAAAUUUCUUAGUGGACAAGUGUUUAGGAUAAGGAGGUGUUUACAGCAAACAGGAAUUCCAGGCAGAGAAAUUUUCAUUCACAGAGGCAUGAAUGGAACUUAUGCUAAAGUAUGAGGAACUACAAGUCAUUUGGUAAGACUGUAGUCUCAGAAGAAAUGAAAGAUGGUGAAUUAAUGGUUGUCAAUCACAGAGGAUCUUUUAUGUCCUGCAAAUGAUUCAAGACAUUAAGCAGCACAAUGGGGAUGAAGAUAGAGUUGAGCUAUAUUUUGAAGGUAGAAUUUAUAGAAUGAGUUGACAAUGUAAGAUUGAAGGAAAGAAAGGAAGAGUUUUCCAGAUUUCUGAUUCAGGUAAGUAAUUGUUGAUGUCAUUGAUCAGAAGAAAGAAUUUAGGAGAAAACUUAGGUUUAGGGGCAAAAUGAUGAAUUUCAUUUGGGUAUAUUAAAUCUUACUUGUCAGGAUCUCAGGCAGGAGACACACCUGGGUUGGAGAAAAGAUUGGAGAGUGCUAAACAUUCAGUUGACUGACUAGAAGUUAGAAAUCCCAAGUUUCUGACUAUGUUGUUAUGUUCUUCACUGGCUUUAUGACUAGUGAAUUUUACCUUUUUUUUGAGACAAGAGUCUUGCUCUGUCACCAGGCUGGAGUGCAGUGACGUGAUCUUGGUUCACUGCAACCUCCACCUACUGGGUUCAAGCGAUUCUCCUGCCUCAGCCUUCCAAGUAGCUGGGAUUACAGGCAUGCGCCACCACGCCCAGGUAAUUUUUUUUUUCUUUUUGUAAUUUGUGGUAGAGACAGUGUUUCACCAUAUUGGCCAGGAUGUUCUCGAUCUCCUGACCUCAUGAUCUGCCUACCUCGGCCUCCCAAAGUGCUGGGAUUAUGGAUGUGAGCCACUGUGCCCAGCCUACCUUUCCUUUUUCUAUAAGGGAUUUAAAGCAGCUUGACUUUGUAAUUAUGACAUAUCAUAAAUGUCUAGGUCUCAGCCUCCAUUUUCUCAUGAGUGCAAAUUUUGUAAAACUACCCAACAUCCUUCAGAGAGUUGUUUUAAGGAUCACAUUUUUUUUAUAUCUGUGAAAUCCCUUUAACAUAUCUGAUAUACAAGCAGAGAAUUAAAUGUUUAGCAAUUAAAGAUUGAAAUUACAUUAAUGCCAGCAAACGUGAAACUCUGAGGAAACUCAUUGAUAAAGACUCUGUUUAUAGUUACACUGUAAAGUCUGAUCAUUUAUUGUAGUGCUGUGUAAUGGUUAGAACUGAGCCCUCUGAGCCAAACUGCCUAGAUUCUAAUAUCAGCCGUUGACUAUCUCUUUGAUUUUGGGCAAGUUAUUUAACCUUUUUUAUAAGACAGAAAUAAUCAGAGUAUCUACCUCACAGGUUGUUGGGAAGAGUUAAAUGAGUUAGUGUAUAUAAGAGUUAAAUGAGUUACCUCUUGGGAAGAGUUAAAUGAGUUACCUCUUGGGAAGAGUUAAAUGAGUUAGUGUAUAUAAAGCAUACAGGUCAGUGGCUGAUGCAUAAUUUAGGUCUCAGUGUAUAUUAGAUAUUUUUACAAUCAUCAUCAGAGACAGUAACAUCAUAAGCAUUUGUCAUUAACCAAUGGAAACAUUUUAGUGGAGGGAGAUUGGAGAUAAUCAUAUUGGUUUUAUAGAUGAGGAAAAGAGAGCUCAGGAAAGUUGAAAAGGUGUGUUCAAGGACGCAUAAAUAUCUAGAGAAAGAUGGCACUGAGGCCCCAACACUUCUUAGUUCGGUGUACUUCCUACCACCCCUUAUUAGGGUAGAGUCUGUGCCAUCAUGAGUAGGUUAACCAAAAAUAUAAUUUGAGUUGAAAAAUUAUGUAUGCCUUAUAGACAAUAACAUUGCAGAUAUUCUCCUUUAUUGAUAAAUUUGCUAAAGGUCAGAAGUUUCCUCUUUACAGAUGUUAGAUCAAAUUUAGCAUGAACUGUUAUGGGUGAGUGGGUGGGUGGGUGUGUGUGUGUGUGUCAGAUAAUACUCAUAAUAUGAAACAUAUAUGUUCAGAUAAUACUUACUAGUUACUGUGUUGCAGUUGCAGACCACCCAGUAUUCAAUGGGAAACAAAACACCGAUAUUCCAUAAGCUACUUUAUUGAUAUAGCUUAUUUUAUAAUUUUCUUUGUGAUUUAUUAGGUGAAUUAAACACAUAAGAAGAGAUUUUCUUGUUUUGUAAGUUUAUGAUGCAUAUUAGAUCUCAGGGUAAAGUUAUUGAACAUUAGCACAUAUGCACACAAAACACUGUGAUAACAUCACAGAAUAUUUAAUGAUACUUGAGUUUCACAUAUUUUCACCUGCAAAGCCCAGAGCAUUUCAUAAAUAUGAAUGCUGUUAAUCAAAAAUUUGAAUAAGUAGAUGGAUUUUGUAUUGUACCCUGAAGAUAAGUAGAUUUAGAUUCUUAUUGAAUUUAUGUCAUCUAUUUUAGGAGUUAGGUGGAGGUGAUAAAACUGAGCCUAGAUUUUUAUCAUCUGCCAUAAUAAGUGGUUCCAAAUAAAACAUUUUAGAAUGUUACCAGAAAUAAAGAGUUGCUAGAUUGUCAUACUCUAGAUAUGAAAAACAAGGUAAAUAUGGAAAAUUAAAUAAAACAAAAUGAACAGCAUGUAAAUAUUGUUUAAAAGAUAUAGAGAAAUUAAGAAAAAAGGUAUAGUCAGUUUAUAAAACACGUUUGUAUUGUCUUGUUUACACACACCAUGGAAAUCAAUAGUUGUAGUUUUACUUGAAAGAUAUAAUUUAUAAUGAUUAUUUAACUAGGAAUUUCAACUUCUUCCUUUUAAUUCGUAUUAUUAUCCAUUUUCCCCAUUCUGAGCUCCUCUAGCUCUAAAAUUCACAUGAUGUUCUACAGUGGGACAUUUUGCUUAGUAAAAUCAUUGGGGCCUAAUUUGCUAAAAGAAUUCAUACUGUGUGGUUUAAGAAAUUCAUAGUGAGUACCUAACAAUUACAUGUUGCUGAGGUCAUGGUUUUUGGAACUUUGUGAUAGUGAUGGUUUGGGUUUGCACAGAAAAGUAAGUGGAAGCAGCUCUCCACCAGCACACUUAUGGGAUCACUUUCAUUAUCCAUACCCUAUUUUAAUUAGACAUCCUGGGAGUUCUUCACAGUUUUCAAAAUGGGGACAUUUCUGCACUUCAGCCAAAAUAUAUGCAUCACAGUUCAUGUAGGGUAAAGUUCAUAUCAUAUAGAAACUGCUUGGGCUUGAAGGCCUUUCUCAGUUCCAUCACAGCCUCAUUCUCUCCCAGCCUCCGAACCUCCCCAAACACUAAGCUGCUUCUCUUCCGCUGUAACCUAUCUUUACCUUACCAUGACUUCCAGCAAGGUUCCACCCAAGUUAAGUUACAGUUCCAAAGGAAGUUCCAAAGGAAGUUCACAAAUCCUUUGCUAACUUCUCCAGUCAGAACUGAUUUUUUUUUCUUUUUUUUAUUUUGUUAUUAUUAUACUUUAAGUUUUAGGGUACAUAUGCACAAUGUGCAGGUUUGUUACAUAUGUAUACAUGUGCCAUGUUGGUGUGCUGCACAUAUUAAGUCGUCAUUUACAUUAGGUAUAUCUCCUAAUGCUAUCCCUCCCCCCGCCCCCCACCCAACAACAGUCCCCAGAGUGUGAUGUUCCCCUUCCUGUGUCCAUGUGUUCUCAUUGUUCAAUUCCCACCUAUGAGUGAGAAUAUGCGGUGUUUGGUUUUUUGUCCUUGCGAUAGUUUGCUGAGAAUGAUGGUUUCCACCUUCAUCCAUGUCCCUACAAAGGACAUGAACUCAUCAUUUUUUAUGGCUGCAUAGUAUUCCAUGGUGUAUAUGUGCCACAUUUUCUUAAUCCAGUCUAUCGUUGUUGGACAUUUGGGUUGGUUCCAAGUCUUUGCUAUUGUGAGUGCCACAAUAAACAUAUGUGUGCAUGUGUCUUUAUAGCAGCAUGAUUAUAACCCUUUGGGUAUAUACCCAGUAAUGGGAUAGCUGGGUCAAAUGGUAUUUCUAGUUCUAGAUCCCUGAGGAAUCGCCACACCAACUUCCACAAUGGUUGAACUAGUUUACAGUCCCACCAACAGUGUAAAAGUGUUCCUAUUUCUCCACAUCCUCUCCAGCACCUGUUGUUUCCUGACUUUUUAAUGAUCGCCAUUCUAACUGAUGUGAGAUGGUAUCUCAUUGUGGUUUUGAUUUGCAUUUCUCUGAUGGCCAGUGAUGAUGAGCAUUUUUUCAUGUGUCUGUUGGCUGCAUAAAUGUCUUCUUUUGAGAAUUGUGUGUUCAUAUCCUUCGCCCACUUGUUGAUGGGGUUGUUUGUUUUUUUCUUGUAAAUUUGUUUGAGUUCAUUGUAGAUUCUGGAUAUUAGCCCUUUGUCAGAUGAGUAGGUUGCGAAAAUUUUCUCCCAUUUUGUAGGUUGCCUGUUCACUCUGAUGGUAGUUUCUUUUGCUGUGCAGAAACUCUUUAGUUUAAUUAGAUCCCAUUUGUCAAUUUUGGCUUUUGUUGCCAUUGCUUUUGGUGUUUUAGACAUGAAGUCCUUGCCCAUGCCUAUGUCCUGAAUGGUAAUGCCUAGGUUUUCUUCUAGGGUUUUUAUGGUUUUAGGUCUAACAUGUAAGUCUUUAACCCAUCUUGAAUUAAUUUUUGUAUAAGGUGUAAGGAAGGGAUCCAGUUUCAGCUUUCUACAUACAGCUAGCCAGUUUUCGCAGCACCAUUUAUUAAAUAGGAAAUCCAUUCCCCAUUGCUUAUUUUUGUCAGGUUUGUCAAAGAUCAGAUGGUUGUAGAUAUGCGGCGUUAUUUCUGAGGUCUCUGUUCUGUUCCAUUGAUCUAUAUCUUUGUUUUGGUACCAGUACCAUGCUGUUUUGGUUACUGUAGCCUCGUAGUAUAGUUUGAAGUCAGGUAGCAUGAUGCUUCCGGCUUUGUUCUUUUGGGUUAGGAUUGACUUGGCUAUGCGGGCUCUUUUUUGGUUCCAUAUGAACUUUAAAGUAGUUUUUUCCAAUUCUGUGAAGAAAGUCAUUGGUAGCUUGACGGGGAUGGCAUGGAAUCUAUAAAUUACCUUGGGCAGUAUGGCCAUUUUCACAAUAUUGAUUCUUCCUACCCGUGAGCAUGGAAUGUUCUUCCAUGUGUUUGUAUCCUCUUUUAUUUCAUUGAGCAGUGGUUUGUAGUUCUCCUUGAAGAGGUCCUUCACAUCCCUUGUAAGUUGGAUUCCUAGGUAUUUUAUUCUCUUUGAAGCAAUUGUGAAUGGGAGUUCACUCAUGAUUUGGCUCUCUGUUUGUCUGUUAUUGGUGUAUAAGAAUGCUCGUGAUUUUGGUACAUUGAUUUUGUAUCCUGAGACUUUGCUGAAGUUGCUUAUCAGCUUAAGGAGAUUUUGGGCUGAGACAAUGGGGUUUUCUGGAUAUGCAAUCAUGUCAUCUGCAAACAGGGACAAUUAGACUUCCUCUUUUCCUAAUUGAAUACCCUUUAUUUCCUUCUCCUGCCUAAUUGCCCUGGCCAGAACUUCUAACACUAUGUUGAAUCCAAAAUGUAAAGACCAUCAAGGCUAGGAAGAAACUGCAUCAACUAAUGAGCAAAAUAACCAGCUAACAUCAUAAUGACAGGACCAAAGUCACACAUAACAAUAUUAACUUUAAAUGUAAAUGGGCUAAAUGCUCCAAUUAAAAGACGCAGUCUGGCAAAUUGGAUAAAGAGUCAAGACCCAUCAGUGUCGUAUAUUCAGGAAACCCAUCUCACGUGCAGAGACACACAUAGGCUCAAAAUAAAAGGAUGGAGGAAGAUCUACCAAGCAAAUGGAAAACAAAAAAAGGCAGGGGUUGCAAUCCUAGUCUCUGAUAAAACAGACUUUAAACCAACAAAGAUCAAAAGAGACAAAGAAGGCCAUUACAUAAUGGUAAAGGGAUCAAUUCAACAAGAAGAGCUAACUAUCCUAAAUGUAUAUGCACCCAAUACAGGAGCACCCAGAUUCAUAAAGCAAGUCCUUAGAGACCUACAAAGAGACUUAGACUCCCACACAAUAAUAAUGGGAGACUUUAACACCCCGCUGUCAACAUUAGACAGAUCAACGAGACAGAAAGUUAACAAGGAUACCCAGGAAUUGAACUCAGCUCUGCACCAAGCAGACCUAAUAGACAUCUACAGAACUCUCCACCCCAAAUCAACAGAAUAUACAUUCUUCUCAGCACCACACCACACCUAUUCCAAAUUUGAACACAUAGUUGGAAGUAAAGCUCUCCUCAGCAAAUGUAAAAGAACAGAAAUUAUAACAAACUGUCUCUCAGACCACAGUGCAAUCAAACUAGAACUCAGGAUUAAGAAUCUCACUCAAAGCCGCUCAACUACAUGGAAACUGAACAACCUGCUCCUGAAUGACUACUGGGUACAUAAUGAAAUGAAGGCAGAAAUAAAGAUGUUCUUUGAAACCAAUGAGAACAAAAACACAACAUACCAGUAUCUCUGGGACACAUUCAAAGCAAUGUGUAGAGGAAAAUUUAUAGCACUAAAUGCCCCCAAGAGAAAGCAGGAAAGAUCUAAAAUUGACACCCUAACAUCACAGUUAAAAGAACUGGAAAAGCAAGAGCAAACACAUUCAAAAGCUAGCAGAAGGCAAGAAAUAACUAAGAUCAGAGCAGAACUGAAGGAAAUAGAGACACAAAAAACCCUUCAAAAAUUAAUUAAUGCAGGAGCUGGUUUUUUGAAAAGAUCAAGAAAAUUGAUAGACCGCUAGCAAGACUAAUAAAGAAGAAAAGAGAGAAGAAUCAAAUAGACGGAAUAAAAAAUGAUAAAGGGGAUAUCACCACCGAUCCCACAGAAAUACGAACUACCAUCAGAGAAUAAUACAAACACUUCUACGCAAAUAAACUAGAAAAUCUAGAAGAAAUGGAUAAAUUCCUCGACACAUACACCCUCCCAAGACUAAACCAGGAAGAAGUUGAAUCUCUGAAUAGACCAGUAACAGGCUCUGAAAUUGUGGCAAUAAUCAAUAGCUUACCAACCAAAAAAAGUCCAGGACCAGAUGGAUUCACAGCCGAAUUCUACCAGAGGUACAAGGAGGAGCUGGUACCAUUCCUUCUGAAACUAUUCCAAUCAAUAGAAAAAGAGGAAAUCCUCCCUAACUCAUUUUAUGAGGCCAGCAUCAUCCUGAUACCAAUGCCUGGCAGAGACACAACCAAAAAAGAGAAUUUUAGACCAAUAUCCUUGAUGAACAUUGAUGCAAAAAUCCUCAAUAAAAUACUGGCAAACCGAAUCCAGCAGCACAUCAAAAAGCUUAUCCACCAUGAUCAAGUGGGCUUCAUCCCUGGGAUGCAAGGCUGGUUCAGCAUACGCAAAUCAAUAAAUGUAAUCCAGCAUAUAAACAGAGCCAAAGACAAAAACCACAUGAUUAUCUCAAUAGAUGCAGAAAAGGCCUUUGACAAAAUUCAACAGCGCUUCAUGCUAAAAACUCUCAAUAAAUUAGGUAUUGAUUGGACAUAUCUCAAAAUAAUAGGAGCUAUCUAUGACAAACCCACAGCCAAUAUCAUACUGAAUGGGCAAAAACUGGAAGAACUUAUUUAUUAUAUUGUACUCCUAGAGCCCUCUCUCGGCAUCUCACAGUUAAGACGUUGUAGUUCAGUGUGGUUUUACGAGGCUUGCUAUUGUAUCAAUUGUAUUUUGUUUCUAAAAGAAAACUACCAUGUGUUUCAUUUUUGAAACCUACAUGGUCCCUGGCAUAUUGAGGAGGAAAUAGAUUAAAUAUCAUAACAAAUUUCUAUUAACAAGUUAAGUAUUGUGAUCACAUCUGUCUUAAGUUUAUUUUAUACUUAAAAUACCAAUUUGUAAUGAGGUUUCUUUCUGAGCAAUCAAUUAUUAGAAAUGACUUUCAUACAGCUAAAUUUUAUAUAUAUACAUAUAUAUAUAUAUAUAUCUGUACUUGACCAAUUGUUUUUGUUGAAAAAGAAUUCUACUCUGAGCGAUAGAGUAAGUCCAUUUCUCUUAAAGUAAAAUAAAAGAAAUAGAAGAAAAAAAGAAAAAGAAAUCAGGUUGUCCUGGUAAAUAUGAAGCAUAUACUUAACAGCCAAAACAGUUUAUUGGUUUGUGAUUUUUUUAGAUAUAAAUGCUCCCUCUUUUAAUUCUUAGCCUAUUAUUAAUAAUUAAUACUCUGAUAAUGCUUUUUUACUAUAUAGUUUUUUUUUUUUUACUUUGAUAUUUCCUCAAGGUCAUAUACAUUUUCAUCUUAGGAGUAAAUAGAGAACAAUGCUCUUCAGCUAUUGUUUAGUCAUAAUAAAAUUAUGUAGGUUCCAAAAUAGGAAAAACUGAUAACCUCAAGUAGGCCCCAGUUAAUGAUUUUGCUACCUUAAAAUGGCAAUUGCUUAUAAAAACAUUAUACACCAUUCCUGUGACAUAAGAAAAAUUCUCCAGAGAGGAAAACUGGGGAUGGAAUUUGGAAUGUUGCUUGACUAUGCGUUUAGAACUGCUCCUGAAAACAAUACAGUAAAAUGGUAAUGUAGCAAUUUCUAGCUGAUGUUCACAAGCAGAGAGAGCCCAAUCCUGCCAAUCAAAUCAAGAGUGUUCUCUGUUUCAUUGGGAAUUGAUGUCUUUAGUUAAUAUACUCAUAAGCGUUAAAAAAAUAGCCUGUGUUCUGAAUUAAGUAUGGAAAAUACGUUUCUGUCCAGGAAAUUAGUUGAGAUGAAAUUAUUUUAUCUGAGGAAACAGUACAGUAAAAUUUCUUUCCUUUUGGUGUAAUUUUAAAGUGUUCUUUCUAUUUUAAACUCAGGCAAAAAAUGCACUUUACAAAUUGGGUGAUGGAACUACUUUAGUAGAGUUAAUAAAUAUUAAAUUAGUCUAGGACAGUAUUUAUAGAAAGUAAAAAAAAAAAAUCCUGGUGUGUUUGCUUAGAAUUUCUGAUCUGUCUCUUCAUAAUUAUACUUCUUAGCUUUCUUAUUUUUAUCUACAGUUAACAUCCUUCCACCAUUCCCUCUGGUAGCCUGACUUUGAUUAAACAAUAUUUUAGGCCAGGCGUGUUAGAAAAAAUAGGCCAGGUGUGGUGGCAUGCGUCUGUAGUCCCAGCUACUCAGGAGUCUGAAGUGGGAGGAUGUUUUGAGCCUGGGAGAUCAGGGCCACUGUGUGCUAUGAUCACACCACUGUACUGUAGCCUGGCUGACAGAGCAAGACCCUGUCUCAAAAAAAAAAAAAGAAAGAAAUGUUUUAACUUUAUGUUUUUAAAUAAUUCUUAACCCACAGACAAUUAAGAAUUUUCAUACCCAAAACAGACCUGAAGUAAUGUUGCAAAAUGGUAAUUUUUUUCUGUUAAAAGGACCAAAUAAAAAAAGGAAAAACAGUUUGACUUCAAUUUUUGCUCAAAUGAAUUCAAUAAGAGAGGGAGUUUCAGUUUAAAAUGAGAAUUAGUUAUUGAAUAAAGUAUAAAAAUAAGAUGAUUUAGAAAGUUAGAAAAACUCUUCAUGUACCUCUUUCCAUUCUAUAUCCUUUGAUUUUAUGACAACUUUUUCACAAUGUCCUUAAUCCUGAAAAAAGAGGUUAGUGGUAAAAUAUAGGGGAAAACAUUUUACUGCAAAGUGAUUCCUCGUAACUCUAAUUCAGCUUCAUGCUGUGUCAGGUCUUCUAGGAGUUUUUAUUAAGCAAACUAGUUGCCAUAAAAAAUGCAGUACCACUUGAAAAUGCCAGUUGUGUGAAUGUAUGUAUAUUUUAAUAAAAACAGACUUGGCAUUUGCUUGAUUUGCCUUUUUUUUUCUUUUAAGAAGAGAGAAAUACAUAAAGAAGUAUCAUCUAUACAUGGAAUUUUAGGUGAGGAUAAAUGAAAAACGAAAUGAGUGUCCUGUUCUUAGUAACUUUGCAAACAAUAAGAUCUCAUUAUGAGUUCUCAUUAUGAGUUAAUGUUCAUGAUUUUGAAACAAGUUUUCCCUUCUUCUCUGUCUUCAUUUACCCCAGCCUCCAUCUUCUGUGAGACAAUUGAGACUUCAGUCCCAAACUCCCAAUCCUGAUCCAGGAUAUGUAACUUAAUUCCAAGUCUAGCCUGAGCCUGGUUUCAUUAGAACCAACAUAUGCCUUGUCCUCCUGCUAAAUAAAGCCUUCUGAUGCCAGCUCCUAGAAGAUAGCAGCGAGACUUGUUUCAGAUUACACUGUUUCUCUCUUCUGAAUUAUACUGCAUUUCUGUCUCCAUUUUUCUUAAGCCCACCACUUCCAUAGGACUUUCUCCCCCUUUAUCACUGGCUCCUUCUAACUCCUGUGUCACUCCUGAGGUGCCAAAUAAUGAUGCAGAGGGUGAUCAGAAAUGAGCUGUUGCUUCAGCUAGGGUUUUUCUACCCUCAUAGUCUGCUAUGGUAUAGGACAUCCUAUUGAUUAGAUUGUAAAUUAUUUUCUCUAUUUGUUAGAAUACAGAGAUUAAGAAUUUAGGGCAGAUCUGUUGCUCUGAAAUGGAAAGAUGUAAAUAAUCUGAGUAAAAGAGAUUCACUUCCUAUAUUGUACCACUCUAUUUAGAAACUACAUAGGUACAUUUAUGUAUAUAUACAUAUGUGGAUAUAUGUAUCUAUAGGUUUAUUCCAUCACCAAAUAUAUGUGUCAGAGAAAUAAGGUUGGACGAGUACAUAUGAAACAGGCUAUCAGUGAUUAUCCCUGGAGAAGAAUAGAGGUAGAAGUAGCAGCAAAGUUCUAACUUGAAUCUUAUUGAAUGGCUUAGGUCAUAUGCCUGUCCCUGAGCCAAUCACUGUGGCCAGAGGGUUAGGAUGCUCUUAUUAGGUGGGCCCCUCUUAAGCCAGAGGUGGAGUCAAUUCUACUUAAACUGCAUGGACUAACAACUAGGGAAGGGUGGUUGCAUGAAGAAAAACCAGGAUGCUGUUUCCAGAAAGGGUACGAGAUGCCAGGCAAUAAAUACAGCACAUAUCCAUGAUAAUACUCUCUUGGAUGUCUUCAUUUGUUUACAAUGUUUGCAUAACACUUUACUGUAUAUAAUAGCUCUAAAUUACCAUAGCUUAAAAAUUAAACAAAAAAUACACAGACUAUUUCAAUUUUAAUUAAAUUGCUAUAGAAGCUAAACCAAUACUUCUGCCAAAAAUUGUCUGGAUAAAAAUAAAAAAAGAAAAGGGAAAGUUGUUUGUACACUUACCUUCACCUGUUCCAGCUGCAUUGAUGAAUAAGCCCAGAAUGAUAUUUAUAAUAAAUUGCCAUCCCUUAUAUUUGUUUAUGAAUAUAUGAACCUUUAUCACAUUUCUCACCAGGCUAAUGCUUGGCAUUAAGGCCUUCAUAGAUUUGAUUUUUAGGAUUUUCUGUGAUAUCUUCUUUAUGAGUCACUAAGGUCAUUCUAGAAUUGGUGAUUUUUAAACAAUUAAGCCUUGUGCUUCUCCACUGUAUGAGGAAAAUAUUUUACAGUGUUAUAAAAAUAGAGAAAAUUGCUAAAAAGCAAUAAUAUUUAUUUUUUUCCUUAAGAAAAAUGACUGUCAAACCAAUAAAAAAAACUAAUAAAUUUCACUGGUUUCAUUACCCGAGUACAUGUCAAGCAAAUCAAAAAUAUCCAAGUACAUAGGGUCUGGUAUCAGAAGCCAGAGCCUGGGGAAUCUUUCAGUCACCCCAGCCUUCAUCUGUCCCCCAUAUCCUCAACAUGGCCUCUCCUGUCACCCCAGGGUAGGUACACAGGGUUCUACGUUGCUGACCUGAUAGAAAUGGAAGUGGUUUCAGCUUUACGCAUCUCAGCACAUUUUCAGGGAAACAAACUUUUUAUGAUGUCAAGUCAUGGCACCCAUAAUUGAAGUUUCAAAUAUUUAGUCGUAUUAAUUUGAAGAAAAACACAUAUUUGAGGCUUAAAUAACAUAUCAGUACAAACUACUUCACAAAUUCAGGUAUUGUUUAUUAUAAUUAAUCACUUUCAAACUGAAUUAGGCUGUGGUCUGUUUAUCCCCAAGCUUCAAACUCUGCCACUGAGGAUAUUUGAGGCUCAUUAAUCCCAUUUAUGCCUAGUGUUCCAUUAUCGGAACUCUAAGCAUGUGGGAGUUAUUUAUAUCCUACUGCUUAAGGUCUGAUGGCAAAGAUUCAAAAAAUUGCAACCUCAGGAAUAAAUGGGUUAAGGUUCUUACCAUAACCAGAGUACUGACAAGCAGCUUAAAUGUUCAUUCUCAUGUCAACAAUUCAGCUCUUUUCUUAGGCUGUUUAAUAACUGACAUACCAGAAAGGGGUCUUAUGCCCCCAGUAUAUUAAGAUGUUUGGAAUGGGUAACAUAAUAGCUCCUUUAGCAACACAUGCUAUCUGAUUAUAACUAUUUCUUCAGUGACUUAUAGCUGAAUUUUUCUCACUGAAGAAUUUGAAAUGUUAAGAGUCUUUUUACUCAAUGGGCCAGAAAUGGUAUCAGCAGCCAUAUGUGAAUUCUCUUAUAGUCCUUUUUAGCUGAAUAUUGAUAAAUGAAUUAAAUGCAGCCAUUGUACUGUUUCACCAAGUUAAAUGAAAUCAAGCAAGUGAGAAGAAAGAAAUUAAGAGGACUAAACAAGGGAUAAGCAAAACAUUUCCAGCUGAGAGUUGGGAACGAGAUGGAAGCCGGCAAGGCAGAAUAGUGAGGACACCGGCUCCAGAUGGCAGGCAUUUAGGAAGGAAGCCUUUACACCAGCCACCAACCUCUUAGAGUUGGCGUUGGUGUGCUUUGUCUUUCGUGUUUUUCAUAAUGCAAAGCUACUGCUGUUUCCAAAGUGUAUGUAAAGCUUUUGGAACUGAAGAAUGGGGGAAAGGGUGAGCAGUGGCAAAGAGGAGUAAUUUUUAUUUUAUAUUCUUAGAUUAUUUUCGGUUUGGUGUCAUUGGAUAGUAGGGCUUCAGAAUAUAUUUUGCCUAAUGAAUUGCUUUGUUGUUUAAAACUCAUGAAGUAUCCAACUGAUGAAACAGAUAGUUGCCCUGUUAGAGAAAUGUAGUAAUUGUUUAUUUCAGGUUUUGAAGAACUUCAUUUUAACACUAUUUUCUAGGAGAUUUGAGAAAACAUAAAGAAAUUAUUAUAUUUAUCUAGUUCAUAAUGUAUUUUACAUAAAGUAAUAUUACCUUUUGGUCUGGCCCGUUUGUUAUUAAUACAGUAUGUAACAUAGUCUUUUAGGUAACUUUUCUUUAUAAAGAUAAUACAAUAUAUGUUUAUUUAGGAAAAAUCUGGAUUGGCACCUGACCAAAAAAAGUUAAAGCAAGUUAUCCAUAAAUACUAGUCAUAAUCUUUUUCAUAAUCUUAUUCAUAAUUAGAACUAAAAAGGCUAAUAUUUUGGUCUUUCUUGCUAUAUAUAAAAUAAUGUAUAUAUGUUGAUAGGCAUGACAGGUAUUUUGUUACUACUGCAAUCCCAAUGUCUAAGAGUAUUUGUUUUUAGUAUUUACCUGAUUUGUUUUUAGUAUUAAUAUCUUAGUCUUCUUCAGUGAGCUAAAUACAUUAUUAUUUAUUACCUACUGAAUAUUAACAGGCCAAAUCUCUUCAUUGAUAUGACUUUGCUUUUUGCCUGCCCACCAACCAGGCUCUUAUUUGAUGGUUUCUUUCUGCCAGUGUAGAAAAAUGAUGUGAAGUUGAAACGGUAAUUGAGCUUCACUGUGCAUUUUUAUUUGGGAAAGAUGACAGGGUUUUAGGUUGCCACAUUAAGGAAGAAGAAUGAAGGUUAACGGUGAUUUUCAAGUAACUCCUAUAGGAAGGGUGAUUUUAGCUUUAUCCAUUUCAGCAUAUUUCCGAGGAAACCUAAACUUUUUAUGAUGUCGAGGAUUAUGAAUCAUGACACCCAUAACUGAAGUUUCAGAGAGAUUUAAUUAUAUUGUUGCUUUGACGAAAACCACAUAGAACCAUAUUUAGGUACAAUUUCAAAAUCAUUUCAUCCAGUUUUCACGUCUCUAUGUUUCCUUUAAACUAUCUGGUAAACAUCCAGAGAUUCUGAAUGCUUCCCUCUGAUAGAUGCAGAGAGCAUUUAAGCUAACACUCAGCUGUUUGUUUAUUAUGUUUCCAAACUUUUUCCAGUUUCUGUUUAGUAUUCAGUGAAAUGGUGUAAAGAAAACCAUCUGCACUGCAGCUGCAAAGGGAUUACCUUCGGUUCUUCUUUUCAAAGAGAAGCCAAAUGCCCCCUGUGCACAGCCCUGGACAGUUGCUUGGAUCUUGUGCCAUAUGUUUUAUACAGUACUCCUGGAGCUAAGUCAAUUAAUAGCUCAGAAGACACAAUUAGCCUUUUAGUGACUGCAUUCAUUCAUAAAGGGCUGCCCAAAAUAAAUAAACUCUUGAUUCCCUUCUCCUAUUAUAAUUGCAGACUGAAGAUUUGAAAUGUUGGAUGACAGCAGAUGUACUGAGAUUGUUAGCGCAUGGUGGCUGCUCUGCUUUAUACUGCCUACUACCACCAAGCCAAAUUCCUAGGUGUGGGCUAGGGUAUUGGAACAAAGUAAAAAUGAAAUUAUCCUUAACAGAAUGCAUUUAAGUUGAAUUUUACAGUCCUUACCAUGUCCUGAGAUAGCUUUUAUCUUUAUUUGAAUAUGUAUUUUAAGCAGACACUGAGUAUUGAAAUGUAAUUAUUGAAAUGUAAUUACUAAAUGUAAUUAUUAAAGUGAAAAACUAAUAUUUUCCCAUGUACUUUCCUUCCAUGGCAAUCUUUUUUUAAGGUAAAAUUUUAAAACUUUGAGAAUAUUUUAGCAAACUCAUUUGUAACUUUUUCUUAAAAACCUUCAGGCUGUGUGUAGCUCUAGAAACCAUUGUAAUCAUAACACACAGAUAUUAAGCCAAUUUCUGUCAUCAACUAGGGCAGAAGUUAUACUGAUUUCUUCUGACUUGUAUCUGGUUCAAGGGACAGUCCAAGAGUCAGUGGUUUAGCUGGGGGCCAGUUUUUGUGAGGAUGACAAGAUUUGCAUACAGAAUUGAAAAUUUUCUGUUUCCUUGGUAGGAUACCUUAAAUAACUAUAACACUAAUGAAGUUGUAUUUAAAAGGAUAGAUUUAAAGACUUCUUUACAAAAAGUUGUAAUCAUUUUCUUCCAACCUGUUUGUACACAAUUAUAUAUGUCUUCAUGUAUAUUUAUUUAAAUUUUUUUUAAAAAUUAAUGCUUUGGGAAUAUCAGUUGCUUUCAUAGGAGUCUUAAGUAAUUUAUCUGAAAUUAUCAAAUAUUUACUUGGUUAAAAUUAGACUUUGUGUUUGGGUGACUAGAGAAAAGGUACAAAUGAAGGGAAGUGGUUAGGAAGAGGGAUGAUUUGUCACUUGUUUUGUUCAGGUUGGAGAUGGAUACAAGCACAAUGAGAUUUCUUGUUUGUAUUUUUUAACACACAUCAGAAAAUUCAGACACGCUUUCAAACUAGGUUUUUUAAUGGCCAAAGAAAUGUCCUCCUGGGUUGAGAAUAAGAAUGAACAUACUGUAUUUGACCGAAAGGAGCUAACUCUAUCAGCUUUAAAAUGGGGUAGACUCCAUAGGGACUAGAAGAAUAGGCUUGAAGAAUAAAGCUUCGCAUAGAGGAGAAACCAGAGUAAGCACAUACAAGGAAUGUAGAAAAUUAGAGCAUAUUAGGUUUUAACCUAUCUUCUAGUAAGAUUUUAAAACUAAGAGCCAGAACAAGUCUCUUAAACAGUGACCAAGAAUUGAUACAGAGAUGGGGACUGACUACUUAGCAUAGAUUGGUCAUUAUGGUCCAACAUCCAUGGAUAAUCAGAACAGACAUAUACAAAGGUAAUAUUAAAGGAUUUACACCUAUCCUGAAACAUAUUAAACCUCCUCAAACCACAGUCGGGUCAUUUGGCUAUUUCAUCCUAAGGAAAUAUUUAACUGUUUUUCAAAUGCUUUUUACUUUCUAAGAGUCCUUUGUACUUUCUGACAUAAUUAAGAUUUUUCUCAUCUUUCAUAUCACCUUUUCUGACUAUGCCAGAAAAUUUCAAAGGGGGAUUUAAAAAAAGAAAGCAUUUAAAUUGGAUCAUAUUUCUAAAUUGAGAAGUUGACCAGAAAUUUGGCAGCCAUAGAUCUGAGCACAGAAAUAUUUUAUCAUUUUAAUUGCCUUUUUAGUGUGCAGUAUCCCUUUAGUUGGUUUCAUUUUUUUGAGACCAACUAUUUUUUGGGUUUUGUGGGAAUUUUUCCCUUUGAAGAUUGUUAAGAAUUUUCAUGCUUAACAUAUAGGAAAGAAGAUUAUCUGUUAAAGUGCAAGAUAAUAGGGAAUAAGAUAUGGAAUACUUUUGAAACUAUGGAUAAUUCCUCUCAAAUAAUCAGUUUAAUGCUAUCUUGGAUCCAUAGCAUAUCUUCCUUCAAUAGCCCUUUACUUUAUUUCAAGACAUUUUAUCAUGUUAAUCUAUUAAUGUUUCCAUGAGUUAAAUGGAUGCCAAAUAAUAUCUGCAUUGAACAUAUUGAAAAAUUAUGGUACAAUGAAGUCUAAAGUGAAGUCCAAAAUUAUGCAGAAAAGAACUUCAGAGCCAGAACAUGAACCAACUCUCUUGGACUUCCGCUGACAUUUGAGCUCGUUGCUUUAAAUACAUGCAAUAAAUAGGUUUUGUACUGAUUUUUCUAGUAAUUUCAUGGAUUUAGCUAUCCAUCUUAUUACUCACCAGGUUCCCUCUGUGAUCAAUAACAAGGAUUCCUAAUUAAGAGUGCAGUCUUUGGCCUAAGAAUGGAACAAAGAUAACUGGUCCACUUAUUGAUUUAUUGAAUGAAUGGCUUCCCCCACUUUAGCAAGGGUUGGUCUAACUAGAGGAGUUAACUCUUCACUGAAAAUAGACUAGAUAAUGCCAAAUAUAAAGUCUUUUUGAUUUUUCUACCUUGUAUAAAUUGUGUGCUUGGGGUAUAGCAUUAUACCCCAAGCAUUAUACCACGUCAUUAGGUUUUAGAAAAGUUUCAAAAUAUCUCUAAAACACAAUUAUGCAAAGUAAAAGCCAUGUAUAAGACAAGUCAAGAUUGUAAGGCCAAUGUUACUGCAUUGUUAGAAGAGGAUUUACUGUGUUUAUUUGGCUGUGAUAUAAUACAAUUUUAUGAUUCUAUUACAUUUUUCUUAAUAGGCCUGAGAGUUUAUAUUUUUUCCUUGACACAAUUGCUCAUAAAUCUUGAAUUUAAUCAGUUAGUGUAAUAGCAAAAUUUUAAUUAUAGGAUCAUAGAAUUUUUUAAUGUUAUUUUAAAAAAUGACUUAAUGGUGGUUUAUUUUUAAGAAGAUUUAACGUAUUUAAAGAUAGGUGCAAAUCUUUCAAUUCUGUAUUAGUAUAUAUCUGUUCAGAUUAUGCAUGGAUGUUGGACCAUGAAAGAGAUUGUAUUAUUCGUUCAUUCUACAGCUUUACUCCAUGCCUAUUUUAUUCCAGGAAUUUUUUCUAGGUUCUGUUAAUUUAACAAUAAAUAAGCCAUAAUUCAUUACCCUCCUGGAGCUUACCUUCUAGCACUGACUUGUACUGUGGAACAAUAGUUACCAUUUUCAGACUGGUAAAGUUUGUUCUUAAAAAUUUAAGUUUCUAUUAAAUGUUAAUUUAUGUUAUAUCAGUAAUAGAUGAAACACUUCUUGAGCACCUUUGUUUAUUUAUUCAGUAGGACUUUUGAGUCACUCAUCUACCUUUUAAAACUGGUGUGACUUCUUCGUACUUUGUUCAAGAUUAAGAAAUAAUUCAAUGUAGCAUCUAUGGUAAUAUUAAAGUCAAUUUUUUCCAGGCAGUUCAGUAUCGUGAAGGACAUCACUGGUGAUUUUAUUUCCUUAUUUAAUUUCAGGAGUUUUCCUGUAACCUAGCUGUCUAUAAAUGUUUAAGCUAAUGUAAAGCGCUGAAACAAAAAUGUUAGAGGUUUGUUUCUCUCUUACCUAACAUUCUGGCUUAGACUGCAGGGUAGCCCUGAACCUUUAGAUCAUUCAGAGACACAAGUUCCUUACAUGUUUUUCUUCCAUCCUGUAAGUAGUCCUCAUUAGCAUGGCCGAAGCUGGAUUGCUGCUACUUUGGUAUUCCAGCCCCAGCGGGGAGUGGGUUUGGGAGGAAGUCCGGGGAAAGCUGAUUGUCUUUAAGUUGAAAAUAACUAGAAAUUGCAUUCCUCACUUUUCGCACAUCCUAUUGACCCAAACUUAGGUGUCCACCUCACACUGCAAGGAAGUCUGGGAAAUGUAGUCCCUAGCUGAGCUGCUGUGUGCCCAGCAAGACUAGGAGAAUGCAUUGAGGGGACAGCUAGUAGUGUGCCACAGGACUCGGUGUGCAUUAGAAACCAGAGUUCCAGAACACCCUGCCUUCUGAUUGGUUUUAGUCAAUCCCACAAGUGAUAGGUGAAUCACUACUCUUUUAGACUCCAAAGACUUCCAUGUAAUAAAGUUUUGCUUCAGGGACACAGAACAACCUACAGCCAAAAGUACAAAAGUACAUUAUGAUAUGAACUUUUGCCAUGCAAAUAUUUGGUGUAUAGGAGGUUCUUUUAGGAAUGCCACACAGAAUUUUUCAUCUGGAGAUAGUAAUUGGCAUGAAAGAAGGAUCUAGCAUUUAAAUAAAUACUAUGUUUCUAAUACCAAGAUCAGAAACACAGUGUUUACCACCCAAAUCCUGGGUGUUUGGAGAUGAUAAUAAACAAAGAGGACAUCCCCUAUUUCAUUUCUUUUUAGAGUGUUUACAUGUGGUUUCAAAGCAGCACAAUUAAGAAGUUAGAUGUAGAGUAUUGGCAAACAAGGCUUUUUGCACUUCCUUAAUUUACUCAGUGAUCAUAAACUCAUUCUCAUCUUUCAAGUACCCAUUUUACCAGUUGUUCUUAAACUUCAGCUUAUAUCAUAAUCACCAAGAAGACUAGGUAAACAGAUUCCUGCAUGGCCCCACCCCCAGACUUUGUAAUUCACCAGGUCUUAGGUGGGGCAAGAUAAUUUGCAUGUCUAACAAGUCCCCAAGUGUUGAGAUACUGAUGGUUCCAGGACCAUACUUUGAAAACUACUGGUAACUCUGACUCCCCAGGUGUUCCUUCAAGGAAUGACUUCUCCCAAUUGCUGGGAGUGCUCCCAGGGGAUAGCCUGUCAGCCCAUCAGGACUUGCCCUUGGCUACAGGGAGCUGCCUGGUCCAAGGUCACUCCCAUUUCUGGAGCUCCCCCCAUCCAAUGACUAACCACAGCAGAGGUAGGAAGACCCCAACCCAAGACAUUCUUCCAGCCCCUUUCAGUGGUAGACCUCCUAGUGGUGUCAACUGACUUCCCUCUCAGCCUCAUUCUCCUUUCUCCUUCUCCCUGUGUACACAUUGAUCCCAUUGAUUCCUACUCUCUAUAAACAUCUUAAACACUAAAUUCUGUUUCAGAGUCUGCCUUUCCAGAGACCCCAUACUGCAACAGUAAUGAUUCCACACUCAGUGUCUCUCUAUGGCAGAUCAAAUUGAGUCCAGGUUCUGCAGUUUGAUGAUAUUCAAAGUGGACAUCAACUGGCUGUCUCUAAGCUCUGCAACUCAUACCUCACAGCUGCUUCCUAACCCUCUCUUCUUUGGUCUAUCUGAUCCUCACCAUCCCCUACACAGCUCCUACUAUUCAUUCCUAUCUCAGAGAUUAUGUCCAUUUUGUUCCCACUACCUAAUAUGCCCCUCCAUUACUGCUCUUUUUACCUAUCCUAAUCCUAUACAUCCUUCAAGGCUAAGACACAAACUCAUCUAUUUCAAUAGGCAUUCUCCAUAAAACCACUAUGGAGCUGAUCUGGACAGACUUCUAGUAAUUGUGUUUAUAAUCUCUACUUCUUUUGCAUAUUUCUAUUUUAACAUCAAGUGGUAUUGAAAAUGGCCAUUUAUUUGUGUUUAUCCUUCUAGACUGUUAGCUCCCUGAGGGCAGGGACCACACCUAGAGUUAUCCUUAAACAGAUAACCGGCCCAGAAAUGAGUACUGAACCAUUGCACUAUGUGCCCAUAAUGCCUUGUAAUUUCUCCACCAGCCUUCCGUAUGUAUCUUCUUGCUUCAUCCUCUGCACAGGUUCCUCAGGGUCAGGACUUUGUUUUUUGACUCUGUUAUAUUCUCGUGGUUCUUAUAGUUGUGCUUUAAAGAGAGCAGAUGUUCAAUAAAUACUUACUGACUGAAAGAACCUAUUAUAGUUAAUGGUUUUUAUGGCCCAUAACAAAGAAGACGCUAAUAAUACAUAUUCUGAAUAGAAGACCGUAUCUUAUGAUUUUAUUAUAUAUUUCUCAAUAUUUGAAUGCUUAUUUUCCUAAGAACAUGAGUUCUUCAUAGUCUAAGUAUUUUAUAGUACAUUUAUAAAUAAAAUUACAAAAUAAUAAUGGUAUAGGAUAUUAAUUUGACGUAAACAAAAAAAUGCCACCUAACAAUGUAGGGAAAAAUAUAAUUAAAAAAAGAAUAUAGAGCUGUACUUACCAACACAGACACAGGCACACACACACACACACACACACACACACACACACACAUACACACAUACACACAUACACACUGUCUUUAAAAGAAAAAUUCCUUUUGAAAUACAAUCCAUACCACCAGGUUAACCUCAGGACCUCUAAUUUCAUGAAAAUUCAGAAGAGGAUUUUUAAUAAUGUAAGCUUCCUUUUAAUUGUCAUAAUUUCUAUUUCUGCUAGGGUAGACCAAGGAUUCUUAUCUAUAUUCAAAGAUGACCAAGAUCAAUGACUUGGAUUUAGUUCAAAUUUGCUUCUAUUCUGGUUCAUUCAUAACACAGCAAAGAAUAUAUGUUGUAAAGGGUACAGGUGUAUGCCCCGGGCUCCAUGUAUUUCAUGGAGACAUACCUAAGGUUUGGUGAUCUUCACUGUCAUAUGGAAUGAGAUAUCUCUGUUAAAUAGGAGGAUCCUAAAACUGUGAGUUUGCUGCUUCUCCUACCACCUACCUCCCAUAGCUGUCAGCACAGAGAUAGGCAUACAAGGCAAUAAUCCUACAACUCAGCAAGCUGUGUCACCCAACCCAAUAUCUGUUACCCCAUGUUCCAGACCUCGACAAUUCUGUUGUGCCAGCAGUGGGAAUUCAUACCUUACCAGUGCCUGUGUACAGGACCUCAGUAUUUUCCAUUUAUGUCCCUGUUAGGACUCUCUCUGUGAAUGACUAACCAUGACCUACUUCCUUUUUCAGUAUCAGAGGGUUCACAACUGAAAUGAUUGAAGAGUGAAGUUGAUUUCACAUUCUUAAACCUAUCAAUUCCCAAUUCUAGCUAGAAUUGUAACAGCAUAAAUAGGAAUGUCAAUGUUCCUCUUACCCAUCUUUUAGGAUAUUAUUAUAUGGCAUCACUGUUUAUAGUUUUCUGGCAAUCCUUAUUGUUCAGUGUCUCAGUCAACUGAGUUAGUUCUCAUAAGAACAAUGACCAAAGGAAAGUAUAAGUCAAGCACAUAUUUGGAAAAUCUAGUUUCGAGACAGAGGUCUAGAGAGCAUACUUUUGUUUUUAUUAUGGGAAGUUCAAAUAAAAUUUAGACAAGCAGUAUAUGGGAAGGCUCAAUUUGAGCAAAAUAUUAGAUUCAAACAGCAACAUGCCUCUAAAGGGACAACUACAGCAGCUAAGUAAAUAACAGAUAGCAGGUGCAGGCUCUAUAUUAGAGCAUAUGAGUAGUUUUGGCUUUCCAGUCAGACCUAGAAAGCUGGUGGAAACUGAGGUGUAGAAACAUUUUCAACUAUGUACAGCAGUCAUGAGUUAAAAACAAUCACAGAUAACAGUAUGCUGCCAUCCAUGUAUAAAAAUGAAUCUACUAAACCAUGGGCUGUAAGUCAUGUGCUUUGGUUUGUUUGAUUUGAUUAGGGUUUUUAAUUUUUUUGUUUUUAGUGCCUGAUCCACAUUUCUGAUGAAGGUACCCAUUGUGAACAGUGGCCCCCAUUUAUGAGAUAUCUGACUAAGACUUGUGGAAUAGAGUAGACUCAUCUUGGAGCCACUUCUUCAUCCUACAUUAUUGGCAUCUGCCCUUACCAAAUGUACCCUGUAAAGAAGUUAUGAUUGUCUAUUAUAUAUCUAGGUAUAUGAACCUUAAAAUAGUAACCUGGAUAGGGUCAAAUGAUGCUAACCUGUCACUGUUUUCAAGAAAAUGUGCGCAUGUCCUUUGCCACAAUGAAUAAAAAUGCUGUGAUAAUAUAUUUGUAAAAGCAUCAUCUUAAGGAAAAUUUGUUAUAAGGAAAAAAUAGUGUUAUCUACAUCCAUAUAUUUUCAUUCAAACCAGCAUAUUAACUUUUUGGGAAGAAACUAUGAUUCCUUCUUCUUAUAACUUCUCAAAGAGUUGGCAGGUGUGCACAUAGGGAAGCACUUCAUGAAUGUUUAUUGAUGUGAUCCUUUUGUUGUUUAAUGUGUAUCUGCAUAUUUUCUGGUUUUGUUCUCUUUUCUUGGCCAUUCAAAAAUUCUCUGCAGAUUCAUGGAAAACCCUGAAAAUUAGCUUAUAACAGAAGACAUACAUCAUUAAAUGAGAUGGACAUGCCAUUCAGCUUUGGGCGGGAGGGGAGCUUGAUAAUUUGCUCUCUGUAUUGUCAUUCAUUCUCAAAGUAUUUCUAAUACUCCAAUUGUUGUAUCUAUUCCUGCAGACUUCCCUCUUGAUACUUUCUCACACUUCCUAAUGAUCUUCUCUAUUAGUUAAAUAUUUUGUUUAUAGAAUGUACAGCAACAACAAACUAGAAAUUUAUAAAUGAAAAAGAUUAAAAAAGCUAUCAAUUCUUCUUUCAAGUGCAUGAAUUCCAUUUGAACAGAAUGACUUUGAAAUAAUGAAGAAAAGAUUAAUAAAUAUUUUACACAUGCAUUUAAUAUUUUAGCAAAUCUUUAAGGUCAAUUUUGUGUUAAAAUUUAUGGUACCACUUCAGGGAACAUUUAUGGAAAUGAAUUUCAGAAUUCACCCUCAUUGUCAUGGAGUGAUUUACAGUAGAGCUGGACAGGCCUACAUCACUGCAAAGCUGGUUAUGUUAGAGACUCUAUGGGUGAACUGAAGCAAAGCCUCAACCAGUGGAAUUCGUAAUUCAGACAAAACCAUCGAUAUUGCCAGUGAAUCACCCAUCUGCUUGGCCUAGGCUGUCUUGACUUUGCCUGAAAAGGCUACCACUGAACAUUUUCCGUCUUUAUUUGAGAAAUAAAAUGACUAGCGGUAAAUAAAAAUGAUAAAUUGUCAUCUUUGAUCUUUUCUUCCAGAAAUUAUAUACUGUAGUUCCUCGAGUAAAUGUGACUCCAGUAUGUUUCCCUUUACUAAAGUAUUUGGGCAAUCAUAUGUUAAAUGCAAAGGAUGUGGUAAUCUAUAUAUUACAUGACAUGCUUCCAAAAACAAAUUCAAUGAUAUAAAAAUAGAAGAUAAUUUUAUCCUCUUUCUUUUAAAAACAACUUUACAAUCUAAAUUCAUUUUAUAAUAUACUCAGUCAAUUAGUCUACAAAUAUGUCCUGACUUGAGUUUCAGAAAAAAGGCACAUCAUUCAUUUAAUUUUUCUUCAAUUUAAAGUCCCCUUUCACUUGGUUUUAGUGAAGGAGUCACCCUUUCAAAAACUGGUUUUAGCACCCUCAAAUUUAAUUCUUCAGUUUUUGGUUCUAAGCUUCUAGAUAUACAUAUGGUAAGCAUGCAGUUAGCAGGCGAAGGAGUCCAUACUCUAGGCAUUCUUUGUAAAGACCUCAAUGUUAAGUUGACUACUACCCAGCUCGGGCUAAUAGUAUCAAAGGGAGAUAACUGGUAUUUGAGAUUGGCAGUGUUCACUUAUUCCUUUACAUUUUUUUCAAAAUUUAUUUAUAAUUCGGUAAAUCACUAGAAAACAACAAGCUUAACUGACAUAAAAUGCCUUAUUUGAGUUACAGCGUAUUACCAUUGUUUUAGUUUUUAUCAAAAGUCAGCAAAACAAAGGACCACAUGAAAAGCCUUUCUAUAUUAUCUGCAAGAGGCUAUUGAUGUCAUUGCCCAUUAAUCACAGAGUUCCUUAUAUAUAAAUUUUUAUAUGUAUGUUUCUAUAUGUAAAUUUCUCUUAUACUUCCAGAUAAAAAACGUCUGUUUGUGGAGAUGUUUCCCUUUAAUCAGAUAAUAAGAACUGAAAAAGUAAUUGCUUCUCUUUUUCCUUAACUAGUAGAAAACUCAGAAAUAAAUAUAAUGUUCAAUUGAAGUCACCAUCUUUCCUCAGAUCUUAGUAUUCCCCUCCACCCCCGCUUUCUUCCUAUUUGGCUUUAAAUUUAGUUUUCUAGCAUUAAUCUCAAUUUUCUAUUACAAAUUGGUAUAACGUUUUUCUAGAACUAGAAUGAAUAUGUUACUAAUAUGAAUGCCAAAAGUUAGAGAUUCUCUCCUUCAUUUGUUUAUUCAAUCAUUCAUCCGUCUAAGUUUAUCUCUUUAAAAAUAUUAGUUGAUGAUCUCCUAUGAGUCAGGUAGUAUGGGCACUGUGGAUAAAAUUGUGAAUGAGGUAUAUUCUCUUCCUUCAAAAAGCUUCCCUUCUGAUUUCUUCUUUGUGCCUUUCAUGAUGCCAAGCACAUAGUAAAUGUUCCUCGGAAAUGUGUUGUAUGAUUGCCUCUUCUCUUAGUUGAUUAUUUUUGAAACUUCAUUUAUUUGAAUGUUUUGAAAUAAGAUGAAUUUUAUCUGUUUGAAUUAGUUAAUCACAGUGCCUAGAUUUUAAUAUUUUGUGCUUUUCUUUUUUUUCCUGUAAUUGUGUCCUAGUGUGAUUAGAAUCACAAAGAAGAAAAUAUUUUAUAUUUUGAUAAAUAAAAGUUAUAUAUAAACUAUAUGACCGCUGUAAGAUUCUUAUGGCUUUGUGAUUAAUUGCACAUCUCGUACCUUUUCUUAUACUUUGGCAUUUCUUUUGUGUUAAUAACCAUUGUUUGCCCUUCUGUUAUUAUCAGGCAGAAUAGUUAUUCUUCAAAUCCUUCUUCUACAUCAUUUAAUUUUUCAUGGGCACAAUGCAAGAUCCAUUUCAAAACAACUGAUUUUUAGGUUAUUUAUCACUUCUUGAUGCUGACAUGACACUUAUUUUAUACUGUCAUGCACUGCGAUCCUUCAUGUGUUUUCUUUCUGUUAGCAGAUUUCAACUUCUAGGAUAUCAGGGAUUAGUUUAUAACUUUUCAACUCUCCUCUAGGGACUAGCAGUGUCUUCCAUAUAGCAGGGAACCAAUAAAUAGCAUGUGAAUAAAGUAAUCAGUUCCCAGUGAAUAAUAUAGGUAUUUAGAAUGGCAGAUAUUCUUAUACUAGUACCCAGUGUGCUCACACUUACAAGCACGAACUUGCUGUGGCACAACAGAAACGUGUUGUCUAAUUGCCUCUUCUCUUAGUUAAUUAUUUUUCAGACUUCAUUUAAAUGCAUGUUUCAACAUAAGAUGAAUUUUAUCUGCUGAAUUGGUUAAUUACAUCAGGGAGAAGGGAAGAUGAUAUUGAAAGCAUGCUUUAAUUCAACCUAAAAAUUAAAACUUUUUUCCAUUAAUAAUUUAUUCUUGAAUAAAGGUAGACACUUAAAACCAAUAUUAUUUCUUCCUUAAAGCUCCUCUACUACACAUAUGUUCUACUGUGUAAUUUUGAUGAGGAGUCAAAUGGGGUGAAAUGUUUCAUUCAGGAUUUUUAUUUCACUUAGACUUUCAGUUUGUGAAAUAAGGUAAUAAUAAUUUAAAUUUCAUAGCAUUUUUUUUUUAUUUUCUGAGACAGAAGCAAAGACAGAACUGUUGCUUCCUGAGGAAAAGGAUCAUGAAAGAUCACCUUGCUCUUUACCUUUUAAAUUGAGAAUCAAAGUUCCAUAGAUCCUGCAUUUUAGUACUUACAUAGGAGUUGUUUACUCAUAGGUAGUCAGGAAAAUGAAACUGGCACUCUUCUUGGAAGUGGGGAGUUCUGAUUUACUUUUUGCUGCCUUUGCUCUACAAACCAGAGGCUUACAAUGAAUCAACUCAAUACUUGCUGAGGUCGCAAUAAGCAAUAAAUGGCUGGCUAAUGUAGGCAAAGGCAUUUAGCUAUACUUUGUAUGCAUUGUAAAUGUGAUAUUUUCUGGAGUGUUCGGCUAACACCUUGUAGAUAUCCUUGGUUAAUUAACCAAGUAUUGAAAGAAGGAACCCUAUCUUUUCACCUGUGAUCUUGCAGGUCUUGCUUUCUAGGUAAGCAGAGCUGUGGGUUGUAAUACAAAGAUUUUUGUUGGUAUGUGAAAUCUGAGUUCUUCCUUAUCUAGCUUAAACUGUUUCCUCUUCCAAAAAGGAAAAACUAUAUUCCAGAAAAGUAGUCUAUGAAAUAACAUAAUAUAGUGUAUAUUCUUAGUAUUUGAAAGAAAUUGAGAUUGUGUUUUAAGUUACCAUAGGAUGAGAACUUGGUCCAAUAAUAUUUAACUGGAGAGUUUUUGUUAGAAAAUCUCUUUCUAAAAGUCAGAAACAAAGAUUUUGAAUAAUGAAGACAAGAAAAGAUAGUAAAAUAACAUACCAUUUUGAAUUGUUGUGUUGGAAAGGGCACUGGGCGAGGAAGCAAGAAGAUAGAGUUCUAUUUCUGCCUUGAACUCAUUUCUUUACCUCUCUACAGUGCUUUACCUCUCUGAAGCUUGGCAUCCAGGUGGAGCACUGGAUGAGUUCUAAGUCCAUCUGUAUUAGUUCUUUCUCAUGCUGCUAAUAAAGACAUGCCCAAGACUGGGUAAUUUAUAAAGGAAAGAGGUGUAAUUGACUCAUAGUUUAGCAUGGCUGGGAGGCCUCCGGAAGCUUAUAAUCAUGGUGGAAGGAGAAACAAACACAUCCUUCUUCACAUGGUGGCAGCAGGAAGAAAUGAGAGUGAAAGGGGAAGGCCCCUUAUAAAACCAUCAGAUUUCGUGAGAACUCACUCACUAUCACAAGAAGAGCAUGAGAGUAACCGCCCUGAUGAUUCAAUUACCUUCCACCACGUCCUUCUCCCAACACGUGGAGAUUAUGGGAACUACAAUUCAAGAUCAGAUUUGGGUGGGGACACAGCCAAACCAUAUCACCACCUAUCUCUGUCCUACUGCAAGGCAAGCAUUGCUUUGUAUAAUGCUCUCCUUGGGGGUAAGAAAGUUGCUUUCUCCUUCUCUGUAUCCCAGAGCCUGGGAUUUAGUAGCUGGUUUCUAAAUGUUGAUUGAUUUCUAUUCAGUUCCCAGAUGUAUGACAAAAAUCUUAGUGUGAUUCCCUGGUUCAGUUGUACAAGGCAUCAGCUCUGGGGUUAAAAAGCAGGAUAUGGACCUGAAUCCCAGAUUGACUGUGCAUCCAGUGCCAUCUUCUCUUUUUGUCACAAAUUUCAUUUGUCUCUACAUUUCUGGUUCAGCAGAUGUUUCUUUAUGGCUGCUAUGCUUAUGCUUGAGUUGGUUGUUAGGGCUGUUAAGUAAAAAGCACUGUCAGCACAGUAUCUUGCCCUCAAGAGAGGAUGUAACUUCAAUUUUAUGACAAUGUUUAUUAUUACUGAUAUAGGAAAGAAAGUCCCUUGCUUGUUUCUGGCCCACUUGCUCAAUACUUUAUAUUUAAACCAUGAUAGGAUACUGAUUUUUUUAAAACACCAAUCUUGCUUUAGACUUUUAAUCAUCACUAAGUAGGAGAAUCUGUAAUCAUGUGACAAAUACUGAGUCAACAGCUAGGAAAACCUACUAGCUUGGUUUGGUAGUGGCCAGUAAAAAAAGCAAGGCUGGGGUCCAAAUAGAAAACUCAGGAACUCAGCCAUAAUCUUAAAGCAUAUUUCAUUUGGGGCUCCAUCAUAAAAUUUGCAAUGUUUGUCUUCAACAUGUUCCAGCCACUUUUGUCCCUUUUCUUAUUCUCUUUGUUUGGAAAGCACCUGGUGUCUUAAAUCACCCUGACUGCCCAGAGUCUUCACUGCAUCUCCCCAUCUGUUUCCCUCCAUGUAUCUGAACCAGAGGAAAGAGCAGUGAGCCAGAAGUCAAAGACUGGACCAGGCCCAAUUGCUAACUAAAUGUAAAACUGUGGGCAAGUCAUUUAGGUAUUCUUUGUCUUAGUUUCCCUGUAUGUGUGUGUAUAUAUCUAGUCAUUAUUUAUUAAUUAAUUCAUUAUUAUUAAUGAAUAUAUGUAUUCGUUAUUUAUUUAUAUUUAAUGAAGGGGUUGGAGCUAAAAGUUUCUUUUAACUCAUAUGUAUGAUUCUACGGGGUCUUCAUCUCAUAAUCAAAACAUUCUUACACUUUCCUUAUUUUCUUCUAAGUAAACCUGGAAACUUUCUUCCAAGGUGAUAAUAGCAAUAGUCAUAUACUGUGGUAGAAUCCCUAGGAGGCUGGGGAUUUUGUUUUGUGAUGAUGUUUUGUCUUAUUGGUUUUUUCCAAGCUUAAUAUCCUAAAUGUCUUAACUCAAAAAUAGGAAUAUAUGAUGAUCGCAUUUAAGUACCAUUUGAUAAUAAUGGAAGAUACAUUUUUUUAAGGAAUCUUUAAUCGGCACUAAAACAAAACUGUCUCCGUAGUUUUGUGUAUAUCCAGAAUGUCAUAUAGUUGGAAUCAUACAGUAGAUAGCCUUUUCAGACUGGCUUCCUUCACUUAGUAAUAUUAAGGUUUCUCUAUGUCUUUCUAUGGCUUGAAAUUUCAUUUCUUUUUAGUGCUGAGUAACAUUUCAUUGUAUGUAUGUACCACAGUUUACUAAAUCUAUUCAUCUGCUCAAGGACGUCUUGGCUACUUUCAUGUUUUAGCAACUAUAAAUAAAGCUGCUAUAAAUAUCUAUGUGCUGGUUUUGGUGUGGACAUAAGUUUUCAGUUCAUUUCGUUAGAUACCAAGGAGCACCAUUGCUGGAUCAUAUAGCAAGAGUAUGUUUAGUUUUGAAAGAAACUGCCAAAUUGUCUUCCAAAGUGGCCGUGCCAUUUUGCAUUUCUACCAGCAAUGAAUGAAACUUCCUAUUGCUUUACAUCCUUUCCAGCAUUUUGAGUUGUCAGCUUUUUGCUAUUCCAAUAGUUAUGUAGUGGUAACUUGUUUUCAUUUCCAAUUCCCUGAUGACAUAUCAUGUUGGACACCUUUUCAUGUGCUUAUUUGCCAUCUGUAUAUAUGCAUUUAAAGUUUUUAUAUAAAUUUUUUAAUAAUUAAGGUAUAAAACGUGAUGUUUUGAUAUGCAUAUACACAGUGAAUGAUAACUAAUUAACAUAUCCAUCUCCUUACAUAGUAAUUAUUUUUAAGCAUGUAUGUGGUGAGAACACCUAAAAUCUACUCUCUCAGCAAAUUUCCAGUAUACAGCACUGGAUUAUUAACUGUAUCAUGCUAUACAUUACAUCUCUAGACUUACUCAUUCUACAUAACUGCAGCUUUAUACUUUUUUUUUGUUCUAGAGAAGAUACAAGUUUUUAUUACUGUGGCAUUGUGCAUUUUUGUUGAUUUCUUUUAGUUCAAAUUAAUUUAAAAUUUUUAUUAUUUUUAUUUCAAUAGGGUUUUGGGGAUGAGAUGGUGUUUGGUUACAUGGAUAACUUCUUUUAAGUUGUUUUGUUUGUUUGUUUGUUUGUUUGUUUGUUUUGAGACAGAGUCUUGCUCUGUUGCCCAGGCUAGAGUGCAGUGGUGUGGACUCGGCUCACUGUAACCCCCACCUCCUAGAUUCAAGCCAUUCUCGUGCCUCAGCCUCCCAAGUAGCUGGGAUUACAGGGGCAUGCCACCACACCAGGAUAAUUUGGAGGUUUUUAGUAGAGACGGAGUUUCACCAUGUUGGGCAGGCUGGUUUGUACCUCCCGGCCUCAAGUGAUCCACCCACUUCGGCCUCCCAAAGUGCUGGGAUUACAGGUGUGAGCCAUCACGCUCAGCUGGAUAAGUUCUUCAGGGGUGAUUUCUGGAUACAUUUUGACCAGUUUCUCCCCAUUUCCCCAACUGCCCACCCCAGUAACCACCAUUCUUCUCUCUGUUUCUAUGUAUUCAACUUUUUUAGAUUCCAUGUGUAAGUGAGAUCAUGCAGUCUCCUUCUUUCUGUGUCUGGCUUAUUUCGUAUAGCACAAUGCCCCCCAGUUUUAUCCAUGUUGCUGCAAGUGGCAGGACAUUCUUUUUUAAGGCUGAAUAAGAUUUCAUUGUAUGGUUGCCAGGGGCUGGGGGAGGGGGAGAUGACUAGGUGGAGCACAGAGGAUCUUUAAGGCACCAAAACUCCUCUGUAUGAUACUAUAAUGGUGGAUACAUGUCAUUCAUUGUAUGUGUGUCAAUAGAAUGUACCCCUAGAAUGUACAACAUUAAGAGUGACCUUUUUUUGUAAACUGUGGACUUUGGGAGAUAAUGAUGUGUCAGAAAAGGUUCAUGGAAGAAUAAUCAAUGUACCACUGCAGUGCAAGCAGCGUGAAAGACAUUGUUAGUGGGAGAAACUGUACUGUGGGGGAGAUCGAAGUAUAUGAGAAUUCUCUGUGUUUUCUGUCCAAUUCUACUGAGAACCCAAAGCUGCUUAAAAAAUAAAGUCUACUUAAAAAAUUUUUUUAAAGGCCAGAAAAGCCGGAUGUUUAGUCUCAGUGACUAUCAAGAGAUCAACCAAGUGGCAGGGUCUGGAAAAAACUUACAGGGUUUGAUUUCAUACAGAUUUUAAUUUCUAAACUAGUACUGAAUAAGACUUAGAGAAGGGAAAAAAAUGGUAUCAACUCAGUACCUGUAUGCCAGUCCUUUCACAUUUAUUUCCAUUUAAUUCUAACUCUAGGAGGUAAGUAUGUAUAAUCCCUUUUCAUGUAAGAAAAUUAGAUUCUGAGAAGUUAGAUUAUUAGCUAAAUUCAACAAGCUAAGGGUAGAGGGUGCACGUGUCAAACCUGUCUGCCUCUCUCUGUGCCCAAUAGCCACCAGCUACCUCAUUCAUGUAUAUAAGGAAUAAUGAAAAAAUGAAGUGUACAUAGAUGAUAGGUAGAAAUCCAGUUCUCUGACUGUAGAUAAAAUUAGUUCCCUUGCCCAACUUUGAAGGGUAAGAUGCAAGAAUAUUUAUUCUCAACUCCAUGUUCUCAUAGAGGGAGAUCAUUUCUACUCUGCUCUCCAGGAGGGAAAACCAUGUGAGGAAGACAUGCCCCUGCUUCUCUCCACCUCAUCAUUUGCCCUUUCCAGGGCAGGAGGAGUGACUUCUCUGAUAGUUGAGUUUCAGAGAAGGAAAUGAUGGUGCUCAGAUCAUCCUUCUGGCUCCUGUCUGCUGGACACAUUCUCUGCUUCUGUAUUCAGUGAGCUUUCAGGCUAGGGUCUCCUCUCAGAGAGCAUCUGGCAAUUGUUAAAUUCAGGAGUAUUAGAAGGUAUUAGGGGGCUUACUGUGGUGGUACCUCUGAGUCAUGUUCUUUGAUCAACUUUAUUAGUAAUAAAGCUGGCAUUUUGAUCUUUUAUUUAUCCAUCACACAGUUGGUUCCAAAUUAGGAGAGAAAGAGGAAUAUUGUUUUGCUUACUGGUCCCUGAAAAUCUCAAAAAUGGGUAGGAUAAAAAUCUAAAGGAUUCAUAUGUUAAAAUAUAUGUAUGUCAGAAUAAUUAUCAUUAAAGAUAACACAGUAAUAGUUCUCAUUUCUGCCCUUAGGGGAGAGGGUAAGAAAAAUCCCUGGCAAAAUAUUUUAAAGAGACUGAGUGACAAAUAUGUUUAAAGGGUUAUUGGCUUAUGGAAGAGUAGAGAUAGUCAGGUAAGCUUGCCUUUUCUGCUUGGAUAGCACCAAGCCAGUGGAACCCAUUUUAAAGGCUGCUCCCUAAGAGCUAUACUUACAAUGUUUCAUUAUUUUACAUUCCAUAAUGAUCCUAGUCAUCAACUGUCUUACAAAUUCUUUUUCUAUUAUGUGCAUGUUGGGAGAAAGGCAUGCAAGUACUUCAUUCUUUACUUGAGUGGUGGUGUUUAGCCUUUCACUGUGAUUUUUAGUGUGAUUUUUUCCCCCCAGUAUCUGUAAAUGUUAUGAAGAGCUAUGUUUUCAUGGGCAGAAGUUUGUGUUUAUGGAAUUUUCUUGAUGGUUCACCUGCCAAAUACCAAGUCUGUCAGUUUUCAGGGUGCCCAGUUAGGCCAUCUGUAUGUGCAGGUGUCAGGGGUGCUUCUCCAAGACAGUGGCACACAUAGGUAUUUCUUAUGUGAGGUGUCAUUAUUGGUCUCUUUGCAUAUUUUUAUUCAAAUUCAGCUACUGUGUUCAGUGCCCAGACAUUCUGAGAAUCAAAGAAUUUACUCACUGAAUUUUGGAACUUUAGUUUGACUAAACCAUAGUACAAUUGAACAUUGCUCUGGGACUUGCUUGCCGGCUCUGAAUUCAUCAUAUUAAAAUAGGACCCUUGUUUAAAGUAAACCUACUCCGAAGUGGCCCCACUGUACCACUGUUUAACCAUUUGCUCAGGCCAAAAAUCUGGAACCCAUCCUUGAUUACUCUCAUUGUCUUAUAACCAAGCUAUCAUGUCUGUUCAGCUCUACGUUGAAAAGUAGAUACAUCCUGUAUCUGACCACCUUAGGUACCUCUGUCAUUACCAUUGCAGUUCAAGCCACCAUGAUCUCUUGUUUGUCUGAAUUACUGCAAAAGCCUCUGGACUGGUCCCCUUGAUGCUUCUUCCUCUCUUGCUCUUCAUAUAGACAAUUAUCCACAGAAAAUCCAGAAUAAUCUUUUAAAAAUGCCACUCAGAUCACAUCAAAUGCCCUUCAGUUUCUUUCCAUCAGUCUUUGCCUUAGCCUCUGAAGACCUACAUGAUCCAACCUUUGGCUACCUCUGUGACCUUGUCACAUACACUCUCCCCCAUUUUCAUUCUGUCCCAGUUAUACUGUUUCUCAAGCAAGUCAGGCUGGUUUCUGUUUCAGCCCUUUCUACUUGUUCUCCCCUCUGCUUGUAUGGCCUUUAACAAUAAGGAAUAUUUAUGGAGCUAUGCACUAGAGACUACUGUAGGCCCAGUGACUAGAGCUUUCAACAAGACAAAGUUUAUAUCCUUAGCAAGCUUUCAUCCUACAGGAGGAUGACAGAACAUAAAUUAACAAAUGUAUAAGGACUCAGGUAAUGGUAAGUCAAAAUUAGAAGAAUAAGAUCCAUGGGCAUAAGAUGUGCUACUUUAUGGAAAGUGUUUAGAGAAUACCUAACAAAGUGACUCAUGAGUAGAAGCCUGGAGGAAAUGAAAGAGUGGCCACAUAAAUAUUUGGGGUAAGUACAUUCCAGGGAGAAGGAAUAGAAAAUGCAAAGGCCCUGAGGUAUGAGUGUGCCAGGUGUUUUUAGGGAAGAGCAAGGGCACCAGUAUGCCUAGGAUGUAACAUGUCAGGCAGGGAGGACGGUAGGAAAUAAGGUCAGUGAGGUGGUGGAGGCUCAGAGGAUGAAGGGCCUUCUAGGCCAUUAAGGACUUAAGCUUUUAAUCUAUAUCAUAAAGGAAGCCAUUGGACAGUUUUGAGCAUUGAAGUGACAUAACUGAUUUAUACUUUUAGAGAAGUACUCUUUCUAUUGUGUUGAGAGUAGACAAUAAGGGAGGGAAGGUGAAAACAUGAAGGCUAAGAGGCUACUGCAAUAGUCCAGACAAAAGAUAUGAUGGUAUGAAGUCGUAGGAUCCUGGAUGUAUUUCAAAGAAAGAGCUGGACUUCAUAGGGUUUGCUAACAGAUUUAAGGUGGGUAUGAGAAACAGGGAGAAGCUAAAGAUGAGUACAAGUUGUUCUGAGCAACUGGUAAAUCUGUUCCAUUUACCAUCAUCAUAACAAACUUAGUGUCAUAAAACAGCCAUGUUAUUUUACUCACAUGUUUGAUAGGUUAGAAAUUCAAAUGGGACACAGCAGGGGCAUCUUGUCUGUUCCCUCUAUUCGACAAUAUCUAAAGCCUUGGUUGGGAAGACCCAAAGCCUGGGGUUCACUCAGUGGUGAGAGACUGGAAUUAUCUGGAAGUGUCUUCAUUCACAUGUCUGGCAAUUGAUGUUUGCUUUUAGUUAGGACUUCAGCUAGUUUGUCAGCUGGAACACCUACACACAGCUUCCCCAGGUCGUCUUUCCAGGCAAGUGAGUUUGGACUUCCACACAGCACAGCAGCUAAGUUCCAAGACUGACUGACCCAAGAGAGCCAAUUGGAAUUGCAUUUUCAUGAUCUAGUCUUAGACAUCACAUAACUUUACUUCCACUAUUCUCUAUGGAAUGAGACAGUCACAAAGGUUCACACGGAAUCAAGGAUAGGAAACAGAUGUACUACCAUUUGAUGGGAGACAUGUCAAGGUCACAUUGCAAGAAGAGCAAGCAAGAUGGGAAAUAUUGUGGCAGCCCUCUUUGGACUACACAAUCCACCAUCAUGGGGAAGGCUGUGAGAAUAGCAGGUGUGCAUCGGAGCGCAAAAUUAAUUCGAUUUUGGCAUUGUUGUAUUUGUGAUAUCUAUAAGACGACUAAGUGGAGAUGUCAAAUAAACAGUUGGAUAUAUGAUUAAAGAGGGUUCUAUGCUACAGAUGUAUUUGGAAGCCACUUGUCUGUUUGAAAGCACGGAGCUGGAUGAGGCAGAGUGAGUAUAAGUAAAGAAAAGAAGGUCCAAGGACAGAGCCCUGGAGCACUUCAAUGUUCAGGCUCAGGAAGAUGAAAAGGAGUCAUCCAAAAAGACUGAGAUAAGUAGCCAGUGCUACUAAGAGAGUGGUGUUCUAGAAGCCAAGAAAAGCAAGUAUUUACAUUAGCUUAAAUCCACUGCAUCACGUGCUAUUAUAAGAUGUGGACUGAGAAUUAAUUGUCAAUCUGAAGGUCAUUGAUGACCCUUAGGAGGUACUUCCUUGUUGUGAAGCUCAAACCCAGCUUAGUGAGGGUUCAAGAACAAAUGAAAGGAAAAUAAAACUUUGAGUGUGAACAUCUAUUUCGAAGAGUUUGGCUGUAAAGGGAAGUAGAUGAAAGUAAUGACUUUUAGAGGAGAUGUUAGGUCAAAGGAGGGUGUUAUUUUUUUUUAGGCUGGAAGACUUUAGAGCGUAUUUGUAAACUAGUGGGGAAAAAAAGUAGAAAGUGGAGUAAAUAAUGAUCGGGGAUAUCGGCAGGAGCAAAGUCCUUGAGCAGGCAGGAGGGAAAGGCAUGCAGUGUAAAUGAUGUAUGCUGGGUUCCCUCCCUUUCCUCAUAUAGACCUGUAUUCUUCUCCUUGAAGAAACCUUCUCUAACUAAUUAUGUAGAAGAGCCUACUCCAUUCUCUUAAUCUGUUUUUUUUGUCCUUCCUGGAACUUUACCAUUUAUUCAUUUAUUUCUUAUCAGUGCAUCAGAAUGUGAACCCUAUGAGGGCAAGGAUUUUGCCAUCUUGUUCACUGACCUAUUCCUAGUACCUAGGACCUGACAUAUAAAGCGUAUUCAGAAAAAUGUUUUAGGUGAAUGAAUGAUUGUGGAAUGAAUUAAAUAGGAAUCUUUUUGUUUUGGCUUAGCAUCCCUCAAAAUUAUUUUACAAAUUUAAUUCAAAUGUGAUUUUGACUUCACAUUUUAAUUAGGGUGUCACUUUGAGACUCCUGGGGAUUAGCAGAAGACUUAAUGGGAAAAUAAUUUGGGAGAAUUAUAUAUUUUCUAGUACCAAGAUUGUCCUUGGCAACUUGAUUAUUUCUGAAGUGGAUCCUUAUUUGACAGACUCCUGAGAUAAGAAAUUGGCAUAAAGCAACUGCGUAAGCCCUCCUCUACCCUCAACUGAUCACAUUGAGUAGCAGUUCAGUUGCUCAGGAGAGAGGACUGAAAAUCAAGAGAUAAAAGCUUCAAGAAAAGCUUUGUAAGGUUCUUUAUAAAAUACCUGUCCAUACACUAACUCAUCUUACCUAUUAGGAAAAUGUGCAAUACAGCAUGUUAAUACUUCACUGGGGGUAUAUUGCAACAUUAUGAAUUAAGGGUUGGGAAGCACUUUCAGAUUCUCAAAUAAAAGACACUCUUUAAGUUCACAGUGUCAUUAUCAUGGUAACUAUGACAAAUGAAAACAUUCCCUUCAGUUUUCUCCCUUAUAAGUCACUUCUUAUUGAUUUGUCAUGUCAGAUAAAAUUGUAUUUUUUUUCUUUUUUCCUGCUUUAGAGUAAGAAAGUAAUUUCACAGCAAGAAAAGAAUACUAUUGUGUGGAAUAUCAUGCUAUGUAUCCCAAGUUUCUUUUAUUUGACAAGCACUCCAAAUUCAACUAUUGACUUACAAAGCUGUGUUAUUUUUCAUUAUGUUAUGUUUUUGGCUUUCAGUGUUAUGGAGAAAUGCCUGAUUAAAAGGAAGCCUGCAAGUUAAUUCCCAACAUGCCCUUUGGCAGCUUUUUCAUUUCACUUAGAGGUGGGAGCAGGUGGUGUCAUUUAGAAUUAAAUACAUCAUGUCUCAGUUGGCAGGAAAACAGCAUUCAGUGAUGAAAUAUCCCUGCAAUGAAUCUCAUUAAUUGUUCGCCAAUUUGUGGUAACUUUAUUUGUAUUUGCAUACUGUAAUAGAAGUACAAUGAAGUGUUGUAUAUUUAGAUCAUACUUAGUGUUAGGUUUAGCUAUCAGCUGUAAAAGGCCUUUGGUGUAACAGCUCUGAAGGGCUGGUACGUGAGUGCCAGUCCAUCUCCUACAGGAGGCCCCCUAAAACAGUCUUGUUUCAUUUCCUCCAUUUUCCAGUGAAGUGAUAGCAAUUUCACAAAACUGUAGCCCAAGCUUAAGCCCAUGCUAUUUUUAGCAUCUUUACUCCGUGAAAAGAUAAAACAGAUCCUAUUUGAACUCUCAUCUGUUCUCAGUGACUUAAUACUGCUGCAAAUUAUGUUUUUCUAGCAUUCAAAUGUCUCUGAGUGUCAAAGGGCAACUGAAAAACUCAUCUGAUAUUUUCCAUAGAUAUAUAUUGAGAUUCAAGUAACUAUGUAUUAUAUUUGAUACAGCUUAUUAUAAAAAUAAUUCUGGGAACAUUAGACUAAACUAAUUUCUUUAUAUGAAGCUGUUUCUAUCUUAGACUGGGAAAACAUGAAAACAUGUUAGUUAAAAGACUCUUUAUAAUAUUUAUUGUUAAUAUACAGAAAUUGGCAAUCUAGUAAGCAUCCUUUUUCUGAAUUCAUCGUUUUCAUUUAUAAAAGGACUUACAGUAUGUCUGUUAUAUGCCUGGUUUGGGACUGGCUUGCAGAAAAUACGAAAGAUCCUUAAGAUAGCCUCUCCCUUUCAAGGAAUCAGAAGUCUCUUUAAAAACUAGAUAUAGAAAUAUGAAAGAGAGAGAAAAAUACAUAUCAAUGUGCCAUUGACAAAUUAUGUGGAACAAUUAGUGUUAUAGAUCAUAGUUUCUUGAAAUUUUAUUACCAUAUUUUCCAUUAUUAAAGGUUUUUACUUGUAAUAAUUAUAUGAUGAUAUAGCCUGUUGAUCAGAUCAAACAUCUCUGCAAUAAAAUUAAGUGGAUAUGGUUUAUAAUGCUUUCUGUUGACAAAUAUGCAUUCCUCUCAUUGGUGAUGCAAGGCGGUAUCCUGAAAAGACUACCAUAGUAGAGGAUGGAAAGACUGAUUCUAUCUUUGCUUCACCUCUUCCUAGAUGUGUCACCUUCAAGAAGUCACUAUUUUCUAAUCUAAUGACAAAAUGGGAAAAUCUAUGGGAAGUCCAGUGCCUUAGGAUUUAUUUUUGCUCUCCAAGCUCAUUGUAUAUAGUCCUAAUACUGAAAAAGAUCCUUGGGACUCUACCAUCCUAGAGGGUGAGAACAUCUGAUUUUCAAGGUCACCAGAACCAUUUUUAAAUCCAGCCACACUGAUGUGGAAUCACCACCAACAGAAUUAGAGACAUUUAAUAAGAAGAUAUAUUAUUUUAAAAUGACCAUUACUUAAAAGUGAUAAUAAGCAGAAGACUGUGUUGAUGCAAAUUUUUAAAAGAUGACAAGCCUUGUUUCAGGGAUAUUUUUCUGGCUAAAACACAUUUAUUUUUAAUCUAAUUUUACCAAUAGCUUUUGGUAAAAAGGACUUCAGACAUAAUUGAGCAUUCUGACUUCUACCACCUCCUACUGUAAUUUUAACACCAAAAUUUACUUAUCAUAUCUGAAUCUAUUCUUCUAAAAAGAAUGUCAUGAUAUUGAUGAGAAGUUAAAAUUAACCUUAUUUCUGAGUAAAGGUAAUUUCUAAUACCAUGUUUUAGAAAAUGUUUUACAAGUGUUUCUUGUAUCUCAUUUUAAAAUGACGUCAUUUAACAUGGAAUUAUAAUUUUAAAUUUUAUGUCAGUGAGUAUAAUCUCUGUGGUGAGUGGCUACCAUGCUGGACAGUGCAGCUCUAGAGAACUGGCUGUUAACCCUGGUAGCACAGGGGAGCUCUAAGUAGAGCUUUGAAAAAUCUGCUCUCCAGCCCCACUCCAGACCAAUUACAUAAACAUCUCCAGGGUGGGGUCCAGGCAUUAGGAUUUUCAAAAGAGCUUUCCAAGUGAUUUCAAUGUGCAGCUAAGAUGAAGACCACUGCAUGAAUUGGAGACCUCAUUGAGAGGUUUUGUUUUUAUCCUAGAACCAUGAUACAUCUUUAAAGCUUUAAGCAUGGAUGAGGGGUGAUCACAUUUACAUUUUUUAAAAAUCACUCUGGUGAAAGCACAGAGAUCAGAUUAGAGGGAAAUAUGAUAGAUGUAAAUGUUGGCAGAUCCUUUUAGUGGCUUGGGCAGUAGCCCAGUUCAUGGAUGAUGGCUUCAUGGUAGAUGAAGAUGGAAUCAAGAGUUAUUUGGAAGAUGAAAGGUCUUGAUUACAAAUUGAAUGUGGAAGGGGAGGGGAGGAGGUGCUGUUCAGUGUGAUGGAGGAUACUGCAAGUAGAUGCAGUCGUUACAUGAUUUUUUAAAGAUCAAAUAUAUGCAAAAACUUGUCAUGAGUUUUGAGACCAUGCAGACAGAUGCAUUAAAAGUAAAAUAAGGUCUUUCCAUUGCUGAAGAAGUCCAUAGGUUUUGCUAUCGAGUAUUUAAAUUACUAACUGUAACACUGACGGAGGUUAGGAAUUAUACCAAUGAUGAGGAAUAUUACUUAUUGUAUUCUUGUUAUCUAGAAAGUAAGUCAUCCAAAGGAAGGGCAAAUUGGAGAGUAAUUCUUUUAUUGUGGGUUCUUGCAUGACCCACUAAGGUCCUUCUGAAGAAAAUAUUUAUUUGUGCCAUAAAAGACAUAAAAUUAAUAGUACUUGAUUUUUAAUUUUAAUAGUUAUAAUGAACUUAAUGAUAGGCUAGUCCAAUGUCUUUUUAUGGAGGGACCAAAGCUCCAUGGGGUUUAGGAAUGUGUUCAGGUCACAUGGUUUUCAUUUCUCCACACUACAAUGAACUUGUUGGAUUAUGUGCUAACCUGUUCUCUGUAAACCUUUGACUCCUUAGAGAGCUUGCUUCUCCACAUUUACAUACAUUUCUGCAUUUUCUUAAACUUCUAUGUAUUUUUCCUCUUCUUGUAUUGAAAAUACAAUGUAACCUGAGACAGACUUCUUCCUCUUUCAAUUGUUUGAUAUUGAAUUUUUCACAGAACCCUGAUAUAGUAAAAUGCUGUGAAAACCCUUUACUUAAACAUUCACACUUCCAUUGAGUAAGACUGUCUAUAUAUACCAGGAGUAAUUUUUUUAAAUGUUUGUUCUAAUUAUCAGACUGUUUAAAUUUUUUCAGUUCUUUAAAAUCCCAUAUUUCAACAUGUGAACAUUUGAUAAUGGCAUUUACUGACAUGAUUUAGUCCUGUUGUAAUAGAAACAACAUCUGAUUUGAGCUAGAAAGAACAGAUUACUUAAAUUGUGACUUAAGAACCAGCUCUGUGACCUCAGACAAGUAAAUUAUUUUUGCUGACCUUUAGUUUCCUCAUUGUAAUUGAGGAUGUUGGUACCUACUUGAUAAAGCUAUUAUAAAAUUCACAGAGAUAAUAUUAAUAUUAAUACUGGGCUUCAAUCUCUAGCAAUAAGAUAUAGGGCUCCACAAUGACAAAACUCAGCUUAUUAGCAUGCUAUCAUUUUCCCUAUUCUGUAUGGUCCCUGAUAGCUGAGUUUAAGCUAAUUAGACCCAAGAUAGAAAACAAAGAAUCUUGUUAACAUUAUACACCUCGAGAUCCUGUUCCUGCUCCAACCUCGGUGUACUCAAGAACGCACAUUUCCAGCUCAUAUCCUUUCAGGAAAAAUCAUAAUAAUCCCUUACUUAUUCCUCUUCCAUUGCCUCAGCCUACACACUAAAAUUUAUUUACUUCAUUAUUUUAUUGGGCUUCAGGAUUGUGGCAUUUUCUUCAGUUUCAUUUUCAGGAUCUUUUCUGAUCUUUCUACAUCCCUGUCCUUUGAAUCUCUAUUCUUAGUCCAAGGACACAGUAAUUUCUAUGCUCCUAUGCCCAUACUUUACCCAAGGCAUGUGAUAGUUUUGUACAUAGCUGAAGAUUUAAUUGACCUCUAAGCAAAGAGUUUCUGAAGGAUCUGGUGGUGUAAGACAAAUUGAUACAGAUUUAUGUAGCUGAGUGCCUAGCACAUAGUAAGUACCUAUUAAGUGUUAGCUUAAGCUUUGGGUUUAUAAGCGUUCCUUAUGUAUUUUUUUAAGGGACCUAAUAUAUGCAAAUAAACAUGCCCUGAAGAGACUACUGUGUCAAACUGCUUGACAGACCAUCAAAAACAGUUACAAAAAAAGUCUUAAAAAGGACUAAUGUGGUUCAUAGAGGUGCCUUUCCAUCUGUCCCCCACCUCUACCAAUAAGGCUGCAUUUAUCACAUUUAAGCAAACAACAUAUUGUCAGAAAAUGAAACUGUCAAAUUGACAAUACUAAAGUAAGUACUAAAACUGUCAGAAACACAUAGCAGGUUAGAUUCUUAUGCUGUUUGUUUAUUUUUUCCCCUACUGUUAUUUUUAAUUUAAAAUAGUCAUGUGUAUUGUCUCACUUUGAUAGUCUUUCUGAGGAUUGGAAUUGUACCAUCUACCUUAGGCUUAAAAUAUGUUUGUCAUAAGAUAUAAGCCUAGUGGAUAUCUCAGAAUCUCUCUUUUAUGUGUACAUCUGGAUUUAAAUGCUGGGGAGACAUUGAAGUAAGGCUGAGAGGAGGCCAGAUCUUCCUGCCGACUAGAAUAGCCCAUUCCAGGUGUUUAUUGGGCUGACUCGGCUAGCGGCUAAAUUAAUCUUCAGGUCUCAGCUCUUACAACCACUACUGGGUUAUAAAGAAACUAGGAUAAACUUCAUAUUCAAAGGGAAAGGCUUUAAAUUAAUUGAAGAAAGUGAUCAUUCUCUUUCUUGGAAAAGAGAAUUUGAUUUCUAUUGCCUGUUAAUUUUUCAAAGAAGUUUAAGAGCUGUAUAGCAUAUCACCUUAGACAUAUAAUUAUAAUGAAACUUUAUAUGUACUUUUUGUUAUUAAAAUAAGUAUAAUUAGGUAGGCUGACUUCCCUUAUAAUUAUCUCCUUAAAGUUUUAUUUUAGGCACAGUCUGUUGUUAAUAGUUUAUAUGGGUCUGUUUUAUUUUGGAUGAAGAGUUUUGACAAUUCAUAACAUAUUGUCAGGUAAAAUCCAUUUAUAUCUUGCCUAAAUUAUAUCUGAACGUAGGAAAAUGAAUAUUUUAGUCCAUUUUGGAAGCAUAUUCUAUGCAUGGUUUUCUUGGAAAAAUACAAAAUAUCUAUAUCUCAGAAAAAAUAUACUGACUCAAUAUUGAGUAGAUAUUUGAUGAAAAAAAUAAGAAUACCAUAUGGCAAAUUAGAAUUUGGUAGUUUAUUUUUUGCCAUUUAGAAAUUAGAGAAUAUAUUUUAAUAUUCUUAACUCAAAAAAGCAUUGCAUUUUAUUCACCUUAAAAAUUAAUUUAAAAAUCUGAAUUGUGGAGUUUACAUUUACAAUAUGUAGACUGAAACAUGUCACACUAUGCUGGGAAUUUGUACUCAGUAUUGUAUCGUGGAUAUAGAUGUUUUACAUUACUGGAGGAAAAAUAGGAACACCUUUCUUCAACUCCCAAUUUAAUAAAUGGAUGAUUUUUAUACCACAAGAUGAAUUAAUUACUGUUGAAAAAUAUACAUACUUUUUUGCUUUGCCCCAUAUUGCUAACAAACAUAGUAUGUAUAACUAAAAGCCUUUUCAGUGAUCUACAAAUUCUUAUAAACUCAUGAUCAAUAAUUAUCCUUAAAUGUUUCAAGGUUAACAAAUGGAACACAUAUGUAAAAUCUUAACUUCUAGCAUCUUCCCCAUUUCCUUGAAAGAUUCUAUUCAAAUCUCAAUUAGUCCCCUAAUGAAAAGCUUGCAUCUGUACAUAAUAAGCCCACACUGGUGGAACUGCUCUCUCAUGCAGCUGCUGAACUCACAAGACAGGGAGUGCAAAUAAUGAGACAGGCACUCUGAAGCAAAAGGCUGGCACUCUGAGCCUGUUCUGUGGGGAAGUAGAGUAGCAAAGGCACCCUCCUUUGUUAAAUGAGAGAUAUGCUUUUAAGUUUGGGUAAGUAAAAUUCAUUUAAAUACAGAUAAGUUUGUAAGAUAAGACUUCUAGAUUUUUUUUUAAUCAGCUGAUACUUUUCUGGAAAUUAAUCAGCUCCCAAAUGAGAAUAAGCCAGAAUGGGAGGGGAACAUAGAGGUGAGUUGGCAACGUGGGGAAGGGGUAAUAGCGAGGCAGAGAGAUCAGGCAAGCAGGGUUGUGUGUUCGAAGAGUUGUGAGAUGAGAGGUGAGAGGAGCCUGAAACAAUAGAAUCAAUAGAGUUUGAAAAUUUACCUCUGAAUGUACUCUCAGUUUAUAUGUGGGAAUUAGCUCUAGAAUAUUUGCAGAAAUAUAGAGACUUUGAGAAAAUCUUAUUUUCAAGUAAUAUGCUUGCCAGUGGUGAAUUCUCAACUUUCUUUUCAGCACCAGUGUAAACCGUAACAGUUUGUUUUUUUUAACACAAAAACCUUUUUCUAUCUAGUAUAUAGAGAACUAAUCCAGAGAGUCAGCUUCUAAUUCAAUUAUAGGAAUUGAACAGUACACUUAAUUUCCUGAAUACCAAUUUGGAUCAACCUUGUUUUUGAAGCUUUGGUGCAAGCAUUCAAAUCAUAAUGAAGCAGAAAAAGGAACCAGGAUAUCUCAGCUCUUCCUCAAGAGAUUCUUACCUAAGCGAGCCACAUAAAUAACUCAUGUGUCAAAGAUGAUUUUAAAGACAGUACAAAAGGUAGAAAAAUAAAAUAUUUUAUUUAAUUAACAUUAGAAGAUAUGUUCGUGACAGUACCCGUGCUAAAAAGGUUGUAGCAAUGGUUAUUUCAUUUAUUUCUUUUAUAGCCAACGUGUGUUUUCCUCUUUCUUUAAAUCAAAUUCAGAGUCCAGAUCCUUUACUAACUUCCUAGUUAGGCAGUUCCCUAGGAACUUUACUCCUGUAUUUUCCUUACUAUUACAAUAGUAACAAUUGUUAUCAGCAUGGCACAUGGAUGGCUGAGUAAGAUCCUGCCAGGAAAAUAAAUAUUAACUCUUUUAACCUGGGUAAUUUUAGUUAAUCCCUGGUAGAAUAUGCUGCGGUGUCCUAGGGCCCUGCAAGGUGAUAACACCCCUCUUAAAUAGUUUUUCCUUGCUUACCGUAAAAGUUGGGAAGUACUAGAUAAGCCAUCUGUCUGUUCCUAGAAAUACCACAAAUCUGUGCAUUGUAGACUGUUUUGCUACACAUGCUGUUUGGAGUUUAAGAACUAGCUACACACAGUAGCACAUCACCAAAAAUUCCCCUGAGUCAGAAAUGCCUUUCUCCCCCUGCCAGACCUCAGUUCAAGUCAUGUUUUUCUCGAUAACUAAACCUCCAUUGUUCAAAUUUAGUAAGAACAGUGCCUGCUGACCCAAAUUUGCUUUGCCUCCAUUGGUAUUUUUUGAUAACUUACUAUAUUUUUCAGGUAUAGAAGAUGUUUGAAUGAAAAGACAAUUAUUUACACUCAUUGCAUAUAAAAAUAACUUUGAUUUCAUUUUAUUUGCUUAUAACAAAAGCUAUAAGAAUAACUAGUAGAAUCUCUUCCUUUAUUUGUUACUUAUAUAUCAGACUGUUGUAAAGUGGACAAAAUAAAAUGACUCUUAUGGCCA